AAGCGUAGGCCCCCGGGAACUCGAGCUGCCAUGAGCCUCUGGGUGGACAAGUAUCGGCCCUGCUCCUUGGGACGGCUGGACUAUCACAAGGAGCAGGCGGCCCAGCUGCGGAACCUGGUGCAGUGUGGUGACUUUCCUCAUCUGUUAGUGUACGGACCAUCAGGUGCUGGAAAAAAGACAAGAAUUAUGUGUAUUCUACGUGAACUUUAUGGUGUUGGAGUGGAAAAAUUGAGAAUUGAACAUCAGACCAUCACAACUCCAUCUAAAAAAAAAAUUGAAAUUAGCACCAUUGCAAGUAACUACCACCUUGAAGUUAAUCCUAGUGAUGCUGGAAAUAGUGACCGAGUAGUCAUUCAGGAGAUGUUGAAAACAGUGGCACAAUCACAACAACUUGAAACAAACUCUCAAAGGGAUUUUAAAGUGGUAUUAUUGACAGAAGUUGACAAACUCACCAAAGAUGCUCAGCAUGCCUUGCGAAGAACCAUGGAAAAAUAUAUGUCUACCUGCAGAUUGAUCUUGUGCUGCAAUUCUACAUCUAAAGUGAUCCCACCUAUUCGUAGUAGGUGCUUGGCGGUUCGUGUGCCUGCUCCCAGCAUUGAAGAUAUUUGCCACGUGUUAUCUACUGUGUGUAAGAAGGAAGGUCUGAAUCUUCCUUCACAACUGGCUCAUAGACUUGCAGAGAAGUCUUGUAGAAAUCUCAGAAAAGCCCUGCUUAUGUGUGAAGCCUGCAGAGUGCAACAAUAUCCUUUUACUGCAGAUCAAGAAAUCCCUGAGACAGAUUGGGAGGUGUAUCUGAGGGAGACUGCAAAUGCUAUUGUCAGUCAGCAAACUCCACAAAGGCUCCUUGAAGUUCGUGGAAGGCUGUAUGAGCUUCUAACUCAUUGUAUUCCUCCUGAGAUAAUAAUGAAGCUGAAAGACGAGACUGGACUUAGCAUGAUAACCCAAAGCUUCAUUGAUCCAACACAUCACUGAACAAUGCAGUUAUGUUCACUACACUAUUCUUGGUAAGGCAAGAAAUAAUAUACAGAUAUUUUGAGGAACAUUUAGAAAUCAUAAGCGUUGAACCAACAGGGCUGGGCUAGUUUUUAACCUUUAGUAAGAUUUUUUAGCUCCAUAACUCCACAGGCUGGUUGAUAAUUAAAAAAUUUGCCAAUUGAAAAUUUAGUAAACAAAUACCCUUUUUAAAAAUUUAUUUUUAACAUUCUCUUUAUAGUUGACACAUAAUAAUUGUACAUGUUUAGAGGGUAGUGUGAUGUGUAAAUGCAUGUAUGCAUUGUAUAAUGAUCAAAUCAGGGUAGUUGGCAUUUUUACCACCUCAAACCUUUAUUACUUCUUUGUGCUAAUGACUUUCAAAAUCCUCUUUUCUAGCUAUCUUGAAAUAUGCACAAAUUGUUAUUAGCUAUAAUCACCAUACUAUGUAAUAGAGCACCAGAAAUUUUUCUUCCUUGCUGACUAUAACUUUGCAACCAUUGACCACCCUCUCCUCCUAUCCCAGGCUUCCUCCAAUCCCCAGCCUCUGGUAACCACUAUUCUACUCUCUACUGCUAUGACAGCAACCUUUUUAGAUGCCACAUAUGAAUGAAACCAUGCAGUAUUUGUCUGCCUGUGCCUGGUUUAUUUAAAAUGCAGUAUAUAUACACAAUAUAAUAUUACUAAGCUAUAAAGAAGGAUAACAUCCUGUCAUUUGUGUCAACAUGGAUGAAGCUGGAGAACAAAGACAUUUUGUUAGCCUACUAUGGAUUAGAUUCUUUUUCUGAGUGCUAGGGAUAUACUGGUGGUCAAUAGGUUCAACGGUCCUGACUUCAUGGACCCUAUAUAUUUUAUAUAUGUAUCUGUUAGUACGUUGGUGAUGAUGGAGAUAAUGACUCUUUAUGAUCAGGAGCAGCCUUACGACCUCCUGUUAAAGUCUCCGAGGGUGUUGAGGUUCAGUAUGUAAACUGUGUGGGGUGGGUAGGGUCCCAGCUUUGACUUGAGGCCUGCAUAACCCUUGGUAAUGUGUCACCUCAAUAGAACUAUUGUGUAGCAAAUGAUGUUAAUUUAUGAGUUCAGUCAUUUGGCCAGAGCCUACACCAAUUUUCCAUUUGUGCUGAUGAUCUAAAUUUGGUUCCAUCCAUGCCCAGAAGCAAUAUCAGAGCUCAUGUAUGUGCCAUUACUACCCUAUAUGGGUAGUUCUGCCUUAUCUGAUAAUAGCAAUGUUAAUCUGACUUCAUUAGACUAGAAGGGAUUAUAUCCUAGAUACCUCACAAUGGUGAUUUGGAUGCCAUCGUAUUGACCCAGUGUGAUGAAAUGAGCAAUCGUAUUGACCCAGUGUGAUGAAAUGAGCAAAAUAAUUGCCCUAAAAUGGUUUAGCAGUUUCCCACCUCUCUUCGGAAAAUCUAUGAAUCUUUGGACCCUCAUGUUUAUUUAUCAUUUACUAUGUUUGUGUCAGGCAUUGUCCUGAGCUUAAUUACAUCAUCCCCUUUAAGCUUACUACAAACUCUUAAGAUAGGUAAUCUUAUUGAUGAUGAAACUGAGAUGGUUUCACCAUCUUAUUGAUGAUGAACAUUGGCUCCAAGAGCUUAGGUUACUUGUCCAAGGUCACACAGCUUGUAGGUGGGCCAGCUGAGAUUCAAACUAGGCCAAUGGGAUUCCUUAAUCCAUUCCUAUUCCUUUUAUACCAUGCUUUCUUCUAGAUAUAUCAAUAUGUAAAAUUAACCUAAUUUUUAAAACAUGCAAAUGUCAUAGCUAGGAGACAGAAUAUUAUUGGGUAUCAAUCACAUACCUCAUGAAAUAACAUAAACUUUGUGUUACAUAUAAUUUAAUUCACUUACAAGGUGAAAAAGGUUAUAAUUUCCAAUAAUUUUUAUCUUUUUAGUCCUUCUAGGUCAUCACUACUUAAAAUAACUGAAGACUCCACCACGUUUAGUGGUUGUAAAAAAUAAGAAACUAAGCAUUUUUACAAUCUUGCUUGCUAAGUCUAAUAUUAAAUAUACAACUAAGAGUGGCAAUGGUAUUUUUAAGCAUUCAUUAUGCCCUCAAAAUGCUGGCAGAAAAUCAUAGUAGGAAUUCUAAUAAUAGAAGCAACUCUACCAACCUUGGUUUUAAUGCAUUCUUUUUAUUCAUAUGCAAGGUUCCCUAAAGGUUUUAUCUUGAGGUGUUAACAGGGAAAUCUGUCACCAGUAGAGGACUAAAUGAAGUCACAAGUCAUAUAACAAGCAGAGCAGACAAGUAACCUUCACAUGGAUGCUUAAGAAAAUACUGGCAGAAACCCUGAUACAAUAAAUUUGCAAAUAACUUGAAGACAAAAAGGUACUUAGUGGAUAAUGACUAAUGUGUCCUACUUAAAAUCAAAUCCUUUUAAGCUAAUCUAAUAUGGUAGAUCAAGGAGAAAUGAUAGAUGUAUUUUAUCUUAAUUGCAUCAAAUCUUGAUUAUCUGCAUAUUACACCCAUCAAUGAACAACAACAAAAAAAGUGACCUAAGCACACAGCCAACUGGAUUAUAACAACUAUAUAAUAUCAAACAUGUGGAUGAAAAUACCAGAUGCUCUACUUCUACAAUGUCAAAUAUAUAUGUAUAGACACAUAACACAUAUAAUCACAUAAAUACAUCAAGAAUAUAUAUAUAUUUGCAUCAUAUAAAUGUGCUUAAAGUCCUAUGUCCCAUAUAUUAAGAAUAAGAAUAGUUGUGAAAACUUUCAGAGGAAUGCAAGGAAAAUUAACGAGACAUCAGAAAAUAAUUUCUAGGCACAGAAGUUAAAUAUAGCAGGACAAUUCAACCAGGAAAAAAAACAGAUUAGAUAUAAUUUAAUAACAUUAUUCAACUGUCUCUACAUAAUACCAAAAUAACCAAACAAUUUGGUCAGAUAACUAUCCAAGCAAGUCAAAUGAAUAUUUUAAAAAUCCAAUAACUCCAUCAUCAUAACAGUUCAUAUGCUGUAAAUGUAUUGAUUUAGCUUUGAGAGAUAGCUGAGACAUCUGAAAUACAGAAAUUUGCUGUUCCUUAGGGAGUGUUGCCUUGAAUGAAGCAGGUAAGCUAAGCUUAACUAAGACAAAAAUUAGAGGAAAGUUGAAGAAAGGAUCCAAGAGAGAACAUCAAAGGCAGAGCUCCAGGAGCCAGAAUAAGGGAUGUGGGUCCCUCAUAUGUUAAUAGAAGGUUUCAUCCAACUGAAACUGGAGGGCCUUAAGACUUAAAGAAAGGCAGCCUCAGCCUGAAAACAUCUUAUAUCCUUUCUGCUCCAAAUAAAACUGUAAGCAUUCCAAAGCUGGGUAUUGGUGCCGUCUCAUUUCUGUUUCCCUACUUCAUUCUAUCUCUAUUUUCUUUUUGAUAUCCCCAUCAGUCUUUCCACUUAAGAUUUGUUACCUCACCUUAUCCAAACAUCUGAGCCUAUAAUUCUCAAGUUAGUGUUUUUGUGUCUCCCAACUCCCAGCCAUUACCACCAAUCACACUUUCACUUAUGAACAUUUUUUCUUUACUGUCAAACCUCAGGCAGUUCCAAAAUAGCAGUGUAGAAGCAAGAUGACCUCACUCCCCCAGACAAAAACCAAAAACAAAUAGACAGCACCAAGAUUAUCACCAGCAAUAUCUCAGAGCUCAAGUACAAAAAGGAGACAGUCCCUGGGGCCACAGAGAAAUGAAAAAUCUCUGAGAAGGCUGUAAGGUAAUUGAAUUUCUAUAUUGGUAAUGCCCCUUCUGUCCAGCACCAAGUGCACAAAGUAUUUCCCUCCAUUCACAAUUUCUACACUCAAAAAAGUGAGAUCAAGGUGGACAAGCAGGUUUUCCACCAUCUUGGGAGCCUUGGCAGGAGAACUGUCCCUGCCUUAACUCAUGGAAAGCAUUUCAAAUGCCAGAAGGGACAAUAUCACUGAGGACAGGCCGAGAGAAGGGAAGGAGGUGGAACUACCAUCCCCAGCCCUGGAAACUCUGAUCUGUAACUUGAAAAAGGGAGAUGCCAAAUCAGAGUGGUUGUUCAGCAGCACCACACCAUUGGAAGUACAUUCCACAGGACCCCUGGGCAUGAACCCUUAGCCAGCCUUCCCACACUGCCAGGAUAUCCCCUUUGGAACCCCCUCUUGGGACAGGUAGCACCCCAAUUAUUUACUAGAACCUAGGUGAACCUUGGAUUAAGGAAUCACCAAGAGCCAAAAAGGAGGCAACAACCUAGCACUGAAGAAUCUCUCAGAAAAUAUAUCUAAUAAAACCAAAAAUAUCUAGACAAAGAAGACUGAAAUAAAUAACUAACUCUUUAAUACAAAGACAUACACAUACAUUCACAAGAAAAAAACAAAACAAAACAGCAAGCAGGGUACUAUGACCUCUUCAAUAGACAGAAUAAGGAACCAGUGCCUGACCUCAAUGAGAAGGCAAUAUGUGAGCUCUCUGACCAAGAAUUCAAAAUAGCAGUUGUAAGGAAACUCAGCAAUCUCCAAGAUAACACAGAAAAUCAAUGCAGAAAUUUAUCAGACUAAUUUUAUGAAGACUGAAAUAAUAAUAAUAAAAAAGAAACAAAAAUUUUGGAACUGAGAAAUACAUUUGCUGAAUUGAAAAAUUUAUUAGAGGCUCUCAACAGCAGAAUGGAUCAAGCAGAAGAAAGAAUCAGUCACCUCAAAGACAGAUUAUUUGAAAAUAUGGUUAGGAGAGAAAAAAGAAAAAAGAAUGAAGACCAUCUACAGGAUAUAGAAAAUGACAUCAAAUGACCAAAUCUAAGAAAUACUGCUAUUCAAGAGGGAGUUCAGCAAGAGCAAGGAGUAGAAAGGUUAUUGAAAGGAAAAAAACAAACAAACAAACAAAAAACCCCAACUUUCCAAAGGGCCAAGAUGGCAGCUUGGAGGCAUUGCUAGUAUGUCUCUUCCACUUGGAAAGACAAAAGUGUGUAGAAAUUCACACUGUGAACUUUUUCCAAUAAGCAACACAGGAACAAACCACAGACCCUUUGAAAGAAGCAGAACCCUACACAAUGAGCCAGGUGAAAAACUGUAAGUCCCCAGAGUGUGAGAGGGGGAUAAGCUGCCUCUGGGAUAUAGACCUCCACUGGGUAGCCUGGCAAUCCAGGAUAUGGGGGAGGGCCAUAACCCUACCCAGUACUGGAGCUGAUUUAGUGAGUGGUGGGGAGUAUAUGAGAAGGAGUGGCAUCAGGAUGUGCUUUGCAUGCACUUCCAGUUUCCAGUGGGAAUGGAGGGAAGUCGUUCCUGAUCUUACCUCACAGGAGACCUCGUGGAAGUCUGCCAGCUAACUCAAGUGACAGUCAUAGGUUGAGAGAAGCUUCCAACUGUGAUUCAUGAUAUAAUCUCGAGUGGGGACAAACCCUUGGCCAGAACUGAGGGGCAAGUGGGAAGUGUGCUUCAGCCAAGGGUACAGGAGCUGGAUAUCCCACCUUUGUUGGCUGACUGGGAGGAGUGUGGCCUAAAAGCUCCAGUUGCUGUCACCACUAGGAAGGCUUAUGGCCUGGGGCAAUUUUGGGUUCUGAGCGCAGAUUGUCUGGAACCUAGCUAGCUGUUGCUAGUGGAACACUGCAGGUGUUCCUGGAUAAUCUGGGGGUAUCACAUUGCCCAACUUCAAAUUAUAUUACAAGGUGAGAAUAAUCAAAACAGCAUGUUACUGCUAUAAAAAUGAGACAUAGACCAAUGGAAUAGAAUAGAGAACCAAGAAAUAAAGCCAAAUACUUACAACCAACUGAUCUUUGACAAAGUAUUAAAAAAACAUAAAUGGGGGAAAGGACACCUAUUCAAUGAAUGGUGAGAACACUGGAUAAUUCACACGUAGAAGAAUGAACUGGACACCUAUCUCUCAUCGUAUACAAAAAUCAACUCAUGAUGGAUCAAGGAUUUAAAUGUAAGACCUGAAACCAUAAAAAUUCUAGAAGAAAACCUAGGAAAAACACUUCUGGGGCAUUGGCCUAGGCAAAUGAUUCAUGAUUAGAACCCCAAAAGCCAAUGCAACACAAACAAAAAUAAUGGGACCUAAUUAAACUACAAAGCUUCUGCCCAGUAAAAUAAAUAAUCAUCAAAGUAAACAGACAACCCACAGAGUGGGAGAAAACACUUACAAAGUAUAUAUCUGACACAGGACUAAUAUCCAAAAUCUAUAAGAAACUCAAAUCAGCAAAACAAAUAAUCCCAUCAAAAAGUGGUCAGAGUACAUGAUAGACAUUUCUCAAAAGAAGAUGUACAAAUGGCCAAAAAACAUAUAAAAAUGCUCAACGUCACUAAUCAUCAGGAAUAUGGCAUAUUAAAACCAAAGUGGGAUACCACCUUACUCCAGCUAGAAUGGCCAUUAUUAGAAAGUCAAAAAACAAUAGAUGUUGGCAUGGAUGUGGUAAAAAGGGAACGCUUAUACACUGCUAGUGGGAAUGUAAAUUAGUGUAACCUCUAUGGAAAACAGUGUGGAUAUUUCUUAAAGGUCUGGAUAUUUCUCUAUUUCUAAAAGUAGAUCUACCAUUUGAUCCAGGAAUUCCACUUCUUGAUAUCUAUACACAGGGAAAAAGUCGUUAUAUCAUAAAGACAGCUGCACACAUAUGUUUACUUCAGCACAAUUCAUAAUUGCAAAGACAUGGAACCAACCUAAGUGCCCACCAACCAAAGAGUGGAUAAUGAAAAUGUGGUAUAUGCACACCAUAGAAUACUACACAGCCAUAAAAACGAACAAAAAAUAAUGUCUUUUGCAGCAACUUGGAUGGAGCUGGGGGCCAUUAUUCUAAGUGAAGUAACUCAGGAAUGGAAAACCAAAUACCAUAUAAUCUCACUUAUAAUUUGGAACUAACCUAUGGGUAUGCAAAGGCAUACACAGUGGUAUAAUGGACUUUGGAGACUCAGAAUGGGGGAGAGUGGGAGUGAAAGGAAUAAAAAGCUACAUAUUGGGUACAAGGUACACUACUCAGGUGACAGGUUCACUUUAAUCUCUAACUUCGCCACUGUACAAUUUGUUUGCAUAACAAAAAAACCACUUGUACCCCAAAAGCUAUUGAAACAAAGAAAUAUAUAUAUAUGUAUAUAUAUAAUUUUAAAAAAGGAUUGAUUGCAAAAGUUUCUAUUCUAAUAUAAAAAGAAAGUAUAAAAUAGUUUAAACCAAAACAAAAAGAAAACUUUCCAAAUCUUCAAAUAGAUGUAAAUAUACAGGUAUAAGAACAUCAGAGAACACCAAAUAGUUUCAACCCAAGUAAGAUUAUCCCCAGGGCAUAUAAUAGUUAAACUCUCAAUGUUCAAAGGCAAAGAGAGGAUAGUAAAAGCAGCAAAAGAAAAUAAGUAAUUUGGUCAGGUUUGGUGGCUCAUGCCUGUAAUCCUGGCACUUUGGGAGGCCAAGAAGGGUGGAUCACUUGAAGUCAGGAAUUUGAGACCAGCCUGGCCAACAUGGUGAAACCCUGAUUCUGCUAAAAAUACAAAAAGUAGCUAGGAGUGGUGGUCCCCAGUUACUUGGGAGGCUGAGGCAUGAAAAUCACCUGAACUCAGGAGGCAGAGGUUGCAGUGAGCUGAGAUUGCACUGCUGCACUCCAGCCUGGGCAACAGAGUAAGACUUUGUCUCAAAAAAAAAAAAAAAAAAAAAAAAAAAAAAAAGCAAGUAACAUAUAAAGAGGCUCUAUCCUCUUUUUGUCUAGCAACAGAUUUCUCAAUGGAAACUAUAUAGGCCAACAGGGAGUGAAACUGCAUUUUUAAAGUGCUGAAUGAAAAAAACCUCUCAUCCAAAAAUACUGUAUCUAGCAAAGCUAUCCUUCAAAUAUGCAAGAGAGAUAAAAUCUUAUUGAGACAAAAGCUGGGAGAAUUCACCACUAGUAGAACUAUCUUAAAAGAAAUUAUAAGGGAGUUCUUCAACCUGAAAGAAAACAAAAAAAUUAAUGUACAAAAAGAAAAGGAAAACAAAAAUAAAAUUUGAAGAUAUAAAACCCAUGGGUAAAAUUAAGUACAUGUAAAAAUCCAGAAUACUCUAAUACUGUAACUAUAGUGUGCAAUCCAUUUAUAACUCUAGUUUGAAACUCCAAAGACAAAUAUAUCAAAAACAAUAAUAGCUAUAACAACCAGUUAAGAGAUAGACAAUAUAAAAAUAUGUAAAUUGGGACAAGAGUCAAAAUGUGGGGGAAUGAAGUUACAUUGUAGAUUUUUUUUUGUUUCUAUUCUUUGUUUCUAUUUUUUGUGUGAUCUAAGAUAAGUCAUCAACUCUUUAAAAAUAACUUGUUACAUAUAUGAAAUUUUUUUGAUAAGCCUCAUGGUACUCAUAACAUAAAAACCUAUAAUAGAGUCACUAAAAAUAAAUAGCAAUGAAUUAAAACAUACUGCCAGGGAAAAAAUUACUUAACCAUAAAGGAAAAGAGUAAGAAAAAAAGAAAGGAGUUAGAAAACAACCAGAAAAUAAGCAAUAAAAUGGCAGUAGUAAGUUCUUACUUAUCAAUAUUAACACUUAAUGUAAAUAGAAUGAAUUCUCCAAUUAAAAGGCAUAGAGUGGCAGAAGGGAUAAAACAAGACCCAACUGUAUGCUGCCUUCAAAAAAGUCACUUCAUCUGUAAAGGCACACAUAGACUGAAAGUGAAGGAAUGGAAGAAGAUAUUCCAGGCAACUGGAAACCAAAAAAAGGCAGAAGUAUCUAUAAUAUAUCAGAUAAAUAGACUACAAAUCAAAGACUGUAAAAAGAAGCAAAGGAGUUCACUAUAUAAUGAUAAAGGGGUCAAAUCACCAAGAAAAUACAACAAUUAUAAAUAUCUAUGUACCCAUCACCAGAGCUCCCAAGUAUAUAUAAAAACAUUAACAAUUGCCUGUAUCAAAAUAUCUUAUGUACCCCAUAAAUAUACAUACCUACUAUGUACUCAUAAACAUUAAAACUUUAAAAAAACACUAACAGAUCUAAAGGGAGAAAUAGACUGUGAUACAAUAGAAGUAGGGGACUUUAACACCCCACUGUAAUAAUGGGCAGAUCAUUCAGACAAAACGUUUUUAAAAACUCAACCAUCAGAGUUUAACUACACACUAAACCUAAUAGGCCUAACUGAUAUUUACAAAACGUUUCACCCAACGGCUGCAGAAUACACAUCUUAUUCAUCAGCACAUAAAAUAUUCUCUGGAAUAAACCAUAUCUUUAACCAUUAAAUAAGCCUCAACAAAUCCAAAAAAGUAGAAACCAUUUCAAUCUUUUCAGAUCACAAUGGAAUAAAACAAGAAAUCAAUUAACAAGAGGAAUUUUGGAAACUACACAAACAUGUGUACAUUAAACAACAUGCUCCUGAACAACCAAUGGCUCAAUAAAGAAAUUAAGAAGGAAAUUUAAAAAUUUAUUGAAACAAAUGCAAAUGGAAAUAAAACAUACCAAAAUCUAUGGGAUACCGAAAAAGCAGUGUUAAGAGGAAAGUUUAUAGCAAUUUAUACCUAUAUCAAUAAAGUAGAAAGACUUUAAAUAAACAACUUAAUGAUGUACCUCAAUGUACUAGGGAGGUAGAACAAAUCAAAUCUGAAAUUAGUAGAUGAAAAGAAAUUAUAAAGAUUACAGGAGAAAUAAAUGAAGUUGGGACUAAAAAAAUAACAAAAAAUCAACAAAACAAAAAGUUGGUUUUUUGAACAAUGGAAUCAGCGAAACUUUAGCUAUACUAAGAAAAAAGAGAGAAAAUCCAGGUAAAUAAAAUCAGAAAUGAAAAAGGAGUCAUAAAAACUGAGACCUCAGAAAUACACAAAAUCCUUAGAGACUGUUAUGCUAUUAUGAGCAACUGUAGGCCAACAAAUUGGAAAAGCCGGAAGAAAUAAAUAAAUUCCUGAACACAUACAACCUGCCAAGAUUGAACCAUGAAGAAAUUAAAAACCUCCACAAACCAAUAACAAGUAAUGAGAUCAAAGCUGUAAUAAAAAGUCUCCCAUCAAAUAAAAGUAUAUGACCUCAUGGCUUCACUGCUGGAUUCUACCAAACAUUUAAAGAAGAACUAACACCAAUUCUACUCAAACUAAACUCUUCAAAAAAAUUGAAGAGGAGAAAAUACUUUAAACUCCUAUGGAGCCAGCAUUACCCUGAUAACAAAACCAGACGAAGACACAAUAAGACAAAAAAAAAAAAAAAAAAAAAAAAAGAACAAAAUUACAGGCCAAUAUCCCUGAUGAACAUAGAGGCAAAAAAAUUCUCAACAAAAUACGAGCAAACUGAAUUCAGCAAUACAUUAAUAAGAUCAUUCACCAUGAUCAAGUGGGAUUCAUCCCAGGAAUGCAAGGAUGGUUCAACAUACGCAAAUCAGUAAAUGUGAUACAUCAUAUCAACAGACAAAGAUUUAAAAAAUAUAAUUAUUUCAAUAGAUGCUAAAAACGCAUUUGAUAAAAUUCAACAUCCUUUUACAAUAAAAAGCCUCAUCAAACUAGAUAAAGAAGAAACAAACCUCAAAGUAAUAAAGCCUGUAUAUGACAAACCCACAGAUAACAUUUUACUGAAUGCAAAAAAUUGAAGGCUUUUCCUUUAAGAUCUGCAAAAAGACAAGGAUGCCCACUUUCACCACUUUUAUUUAACAUAAUGCUAGAAGUCCUGGCUAGAUCAAUUAGACAAGAGAAAAAAAUAAAGAGCAUCCUAAUUGGGAAAAAGAAGUUAAAUUAGCCUUGUUCACAGAUGACAUGACCUUAUACUUAGAAAAACCUAAAGACUUCACCAAAAACUGUUAGAACUGAUAAAUAAAUUCAGUAAAGUUGCAGGAUACAAAACCAACAUACAUAAAUUAGUAGCAUUUAUAUAUGCCAAUGGCAAACAAUCUGAAAAAUAAGUCAAGAAAGAAAUCCCAUUUACAAUAGCUACAAAGAAUAUAAAACACCUAGGAAUCAAUUUAAUUGAAUAAGUGAAAGAUCUAUACAAGAAAACCUGUAAAACAGUGAUAAAAGAAAUGGAAGAGAACACAAAAAAUGAAAGCACAUUCCAUGUUCAUGGGUUGAAAGAAUUAAUCUUGUUAAAAUGACAAUACUACUCAAAGAAAUGUACAGAAUCAAUGCAAUCCCUAUCAAAACGCCAAUGACAUUCUUCACAGAAAUACAAAAAGCAAUUAUAAAAUGUAUAUGAAACCACAAAAGACUCUGAACAGCUAAAGCAAUCCCGAGAAAAAAGAACAAAGCGGGAGGCAUUACACUACUUGACUUCAAAAUUUACUACAAACCUAUAGUAACCAAAUCAGCAUGGUACUGGCAUGAAAACAGACACAUAGACCAAUGGAACAGAGUAGAGAGCCCAGACAUAAAUACAUGCAUUUAUAGCCAACUAGUCUUUGACAAAGUUUCCAAGAAUGUACAAUGGAAAAAAGGAUAGUCUCUUCAAUAAAUGGUGCUGAAAAACCUGGUUAACUAUCUGCAGAAGAAUGAAACUAGAUUCCUAUCUCUGUCUAUCACCAUAUAGAAAAAAAAACGUAUUAAGACCUGUAUUAAAUCUAAGGCCUGAAAUUAUGAAAUUAGUAGAAGAAAACUCUGGGGAAACACUCUAAGACAUUGAUCUGGGCAAAGAUUGUUUGUGUAAGACUUCGAAAGCACAGGCAACCAAAGCAAAAAAAGGACAAAUGGGAUUACAUCAAGUUAAAAAGCUUCUGCACAACAAAAGAAACAAUCAACAAAGAGACAACCCACAGAAUGGGAGAAAAUAUUUGAAAACUAUACAUCUGACAAGGUAUUAAUAACCAGAAUAUAGAAGAAGCUAAAACAACUGAAUAGCAAAAAAAAAAAAAAUAAUAAAUAUAAUAAUCCAAUUGAAAAUGGACAAAAAAUGUGAUUAGACUUGUCUCAGAAGAAGACUUUCAAAUGGUCAACAGGUAUAUGAAAAAAUGCUCAACAUCACUAAUCAUCGAAGAAAUGCAAAUCAAAAUCACAAUGAGACAUUAUCUCACUUCAAUUAAAAUGAAUUUUAUCAAAAAGACAAUAAUGGAUGCUGGUGAGGAUGUGGAGAGAGGGGGACCCCUUAUACGCUGCCGGUGGAAAUGUAAAUUAGUACAGCCACUGUAGAAAACAAUAUGGAAAUUCGUCACAAAAAUAAAAUAGAACUACUAUAUGAUAUAGGAAUUCAACUACUGGGUAUGUAUCCACAAGAAAGUAAAUCAACAUUUUGAGGAAAUGUCUGCAUUCUCAUGUUUAUUGCAACCCUAUUUACAAUAACCAAAAAUGGAAUCAACCUAAGUGCCCAUCAAUGGAUGAAUGGAUAAAAAAAUGUGGUAUAUAUACACAAUGAAAUAUUAUUCAGCCAUAAAAAAAUAAAAUCUUGCCAUUUUCAGCAACAUGGAUAGAACUGGAGGUCAUUAUUUUAAAUGAGAUAAGCCAAGCACAGAAAGACAAAUAUUACAUGUUCUCACUCAUAUAUAUCAGCUAAAAAUGUGGGUAUCAUGGAGAUAGAGAGUAGACUGGCAGUUACCAGAGGCUGGGAAGGGUAGAGAGGAAGGAAGGAUGAAGAGAAGUUAAUUAAUUGGUACAAAUAUAUGACCUGAUAGAAAAAAUAAGACCUAGUGUUUGAUAGAUCAGUAGGGUGACUAUAGUUUAUAAUAAUCUAUUUUACGUUUCACGUGAGCUAUAAGGGAAUAAUUCAAAUGUUUCUAGCAUUAAGAAAAGUAUUUAAGGUGAUGGUUAUCCCAUGUACAUUGAUUUGAUCUUUACAUGAAAGUAUUAAAUUAUCAUAUGUACCCCAAACUAUGUAUUAAUAUAUCUUUUAUGCAUAAAUAAAAACACAUAAAAAUAAACAAGAAACAAAAAAACAAAAUCUCAUGAUCAGACUCUUUGCAGCUUCUAAAAUGUGAUAAAUUAAUUCAUUUAAAGCUGCUUAGUGGAAAAAAGCAUGAUGAUUUCUAGAAGAGAAAUAUCCACUUCCACCCUAGACCCUGACCCCUGCCCUGCUAUGGGUACAUUUUUAAAAUUACUAUUCUGCCAUCCCACACAUAAGGCAAAAGCUGUGAUGGUGGAAUAACACUGAUGACGGAAUAUCAGUUCAGGUUAAAAAAAUGGUGAAUAUAUGGGCAGGAGACAGGGUGACGUGGGUGAAGAAAUAUGGAGAAUAUAUUUGGAGGCUGAUGGAAUAUGGUGAGAUUCAUAGGUCCUAUUAUAAUUAGUCUUCUUGUUUGUUCAAGCAUAACGCUGACCCUAUCUGAAGCCAGUGUGGUUCUAUCAGAAGCAAGUGUCUGCCUGCCAUAGUUUGAGAAUCAGCAAUUUGAAAAGGCAGGAUGAAUGUAGGUGGAGAAACAUGGGGCUGUCUUUGCAGGUGACAUACUAUGGGAUUCUCAGGUCUCAUAAGGAUUAGCAUCUGAAGGACCAUGUGAAAUAACUAGUGGAUCAUUGUCCAUGUCACUUAUUAAUUAUAUGGAAAUCAGUGGUAAAAAAGGAUUUGCAUCUGGCAGUAAAGCCUAUUGAUAAUUGUUCCGUAUUUUAUUCAAAAGCAUUUAAUGAUUAUAGUUUAAUAAUAUUAUACUGUGUAUAUCAGAUAGUUUAGUUGCAUAUAAUGUUAAGCCUAUCAGUUAUACUUCCCAAGUUUACCCCUUAUUCAUUUACUCUUCUUAAUUGCUGUUGACACUCUUCCCCGUCCAAGCCAACAUUAUUUUUCAUCUGAAAGGCUAUAGUAGCCCCUCUAUGUCUACUUUUGUGAACUGACAGUCCGUUAUCCACAGAACCACCAGAGGAAGUUUUAAAAGAGGUAAAUUAGAUCCUGUCAUUCCCUUGCUCCAGGGGUGUCCAGUGUUUUGGCUCCCCUGGUCCACAUUGGAAGAAAAGAAUUGUCUUGGGCCACACUUAAAAUACCCUAACGAUAGCUGAUGAGCUAAAAAAAAAAAAAUUGCAAAAAGAUCCCGUAAUGUUUUAAGAAAAUUUAUGAAUUUGUCUUAGGCUGCAUUCAAAGCCAUCCUGGGCCGCAUGUGGCCUGUGCGCCACCAGUUGGACAAGCUUGCAACCUUACUAUAACUCCCUUUUCCACCAAGAAUAAAAUCCAGAUUCCUUUCUGUAGCCUGAAAGGCUCCACACAAUCCAACCCCUGCCAAGCUCUUGACCAAAUCCCGGUUACUCUCUCUCCAUCUUGCUCAGCCUACUACAGAGAAAGUUCUCUGUCACUUUCUCAGGUCUAGGCAAUCAGAGAAAUAGAUCAAACACUGAUUUGUAGCAUUUGCAAUUUCUGUGGUAUAAAUACUCCUAGAUAGCAACAUGAUGUCACUGAAGGUGAAUUUGGGUAGAAAUGUGCAGUCACACUCCAUUAUAAGUAUUUCCACCAUACAGAAACAGUAGGUGUAAAAAAAAUCUCAGAAGCAUAGGUCAUAGUACAAUGUAAUAUAACUCGUGAUAAGUUUUGAGUGUGUAUUACCUUUUGUUUUAAGUGAAAUGUAUUUACUUGUAAGUUUAUGUAACUUAUUUUAAAAUAACAUCUGUGUUUCAUACCUAGCUCAUGAAACUCCUGAACAUUUUACAAUAGGUUUCACAAGUGGGCUCCAGCAACCACUCUAUGUACCCCAGAUGUCCUCAAUAUUUUUCCCUGGAUUCACAUAUUUAUGCAUAACCAAGAAAAUGCCUCUAUGUUUUGUCCCAUGAGAUUUAGCCCAGACCUUUCCUGCAGUUGUAUUACUUUCCCUGGAGCCUUAUUAGUUAGGUUUAUUUCAUUAUGUCACCUUUCUCUUAUGGGAAAUGGUUUGGGGUCUGAAGUCCCUUUGUUUGGCCCCUGUGCUCUCUUUCCUUGGUGAUAACUCUGAUGCUAAUUGGUUAUCUUCCAAGACUGAAACAGAAACUCAGUAUCUCAUUUUGUCUUCCAAUUAUGCACCUGUGUCCAAAAUUAUGCAAAGAAAUAGGUAUCUAUUUCCUGCUGUGUCUUGUAAACAUCAUGUUUAUUACACUAACAUCGUUUUCUUCCCUGAAUUUAUGUGUGCAUGCCCACAAGGCUGUUUCAGUACCAGCUUCUUUUAUAUCCCUUUGUUUAAAAUACUUAUUUCUGAAAUGCUAUCUGAAUUUGAACAUACUAAAAUUGUUUAUGGUCAAUUUUAACUCUUAUUUAUUUGCUGUACCUUAGGGACUUUGUCUUUCUCAUAACUGUAUGCCCAGCCUCUAGUACAUUUCCUGGCAUGUGGUAGACACUUAGAAAAUAUUGACUAAAUGGAUGACUGCAUCUUCUUCCAUGCCCAAAACUAUAUAGUUUCUAAAAAAUCAGUUGUUCUGCCUGACUUUCCUGUUUUUUUCUUCCUAAUGGCACCACUCGUUUUUUGAUUGCCAAAGCUCAAACCCUGAGUUUUCUUAUGAGCAUCUUUCUUUCACUCCCAGUUGUCACCAGUCUUGGUAGUGUCCCAACAUGUGUUCUCCCUUGGCCCCUGUAAAUUCUUUUUAACUCUGCCACUGGCCCAUCUCAGAGCCUUAUCAUCAUUCACUAGGCUACUGUUAACUCUCUUCUAAUUAGUUUUCCUACCUCCAGUCUUUCUUCACAUUAAUCCAUCUUCCUGGUGUCAGAGGAACCCUCCCGAAGCAAGGCCAGAUCAUGUCACAUCCUUUAAAAUGGACCAGAUGGCUCUGAAAGCGUCAGGAUAGAGUCCAGAUUCCCUCACGUGCCAUUCAGGCCCUUCCACAAUCUGGCCUUAAUCUGCCUGCCCGCCCUUCUCUCGCCGCAAUUUCUUCCACAUUUAACAUGCCCACGUCUCCCAGGUGACUUCCUCAGAACACCGUUUCCUCAGAAAGUAAUGGAGGUUGCACUGAACACAUUCCCCAUGGCCAAAUAAGCUGGGGAGGCAAUGCUGGCCUAAACAGCUGGUGAGACUUCUCAGAGCCUAAGUAUGUUGAAAAAUAAGACCGAACAAUAUGUUGUUUGGGAUACGCAUUUAGCAAAACUGUAGAGAAAAACAAUGGAAUGAUAAAUACAAAAUUGAAGGCAGCAAUUAUCUUUGGUGGAAAGGAGAGAGCUGUGACCAGAGAGGGAUAUAUCAGUGGCUCCAAUGAUGUUAGAAAUUGUUCUCUAUCUUAAGCAAGGUACUGGGUAUACGAGUGCAUGUUAUUUGUUAUUAUGUUGCUUUUCACAUUUUAACAUCUCUGAAAUCAGGAUAGGCCUACAAUCACAGAUAGCCAGGUGACAAUUGUGCUGUAGUUGUCUUUACAACUACAGCACAAUGAUGUUAGAAAUUGUUCUGUAUCUUAAGCAAGGUACUGGGUAUACGAGUGCAUGUUAUUUGUUAUUAUGUUGCUUUUCACAUUUUAACAUCUCUGAAAUCAGGAUAGGCCUACAAUCACAGAUAGCCAGGUGACAAUUGUGCUGUAGUUGUCUUUACCUUAAAAACAUCAUCGCUGAUUUCUUUCACUUGUGUUCUCUUUUUUUUUUCUUGCAUGCAUGAGUGUCAUAAGGCAAAAAAUCUAAGCCUGAAAGACCUCUUUUGUUAAGUAUAAAAUAAAAAUCUAAAUGGCAAGAAAAUAAUUCAUCUAUGAGUUUAUAACAAUAUCUACAUUCUUGUUUUAUGGAAACUAUAGGGUCUUCAGGGCUGAAGCAGUUUUCCCACAACCUCUUCCCCUAUAAUAGUCAAUGUUCAUGGUACAGAUGAUUGCUACAAUAUGAAGCUCAGUGUCUUACACCUAGUAAGUGCACUCUAAAUAUUAUUUAUUGGAUUUCCAGUGACUAUAUUAAUAUUGAACUCAAAUGAUUCACUAACAUUCUUCACCAAAUCUGGUCAUUUUCAAAAAAUAAAAAAUAAAAACAACAACAAAACAAACAAACCAAGAACAGUGAUUGGAAAGCCCACUUUGAUAAAUGUCUGACCUGAUAAGACAAUCCAUAUCUAUGUGCUAAUAGGAAGAAGUCUUAAAGGCAUAUUGAUACUACUCUUCUCUGAACUGUUUCUGUGCUUAGUUUUCUAUGAUGUGCCAUGUAGUGAAUUUUGUCUUCACAAAUUACUUCUGUUUUUAACAUAAAAAUCAUAAUAUCCUUGAGGGAUUGUGGCUUAUAUUUUAGCACUACUUAUAAUGCUAUGCAUACAGUGUUACUUAAUCUGUUGUUUGAUUAAUGAUUCUGUUUGUGUAAGUGUCACAUUGAUCAUAUCCUCAAAACACAGUUCUUAGGCUGUAAUUCAGCUCUGUUCUUAUUGCCACAGCAUCUUAAAAUUCUACCUGUGAAUCUAAAUUGGAAGUCAUUCUGUAGUGUGUGAUUCUUAUUUAUUUGGCUUAUAGUAAAUCAAGAGAGAUUGAUUGGUAGUUUAAUAAACCGAUUUAUAAGAAAGUCCCCAGUCAUUGUGUCCACUGACCUUCAAGGUAAGAAUGUUGGUUUGACCAGUUGUAGGUUCAGUAACAUUGGAUCCAGCUUUCCGGGAGAUACCCAGAAUCUCCAUAUGACUAAAUAUGGACUUCUAAGAUUCAUGUAGACACUACCUAUUCUGAUCAUCACUUUCCAUGAAGACGCAAGUCUCAAAUUAUUAUUUUAAUAGAAUCAGCCAUCAUCUUGCAGUCUGUUUAACUGUUGACUUUUAUUUUCAUUUGCAUAUAUUCCCUUUUAUGAAAGGGCUACUCCUUUUCCUUGGUUCACUUGUGAUCUUUAUUUUUUUGUUACAUGCUUUUCUUGCUGUUGAACAAGGUUUAAAUUGGAUCACUGAUCUAAAAUAUUCAUUUUGAAAAUUACUUCACAAAAAAUUAAAAGAUUAAUAGUUAAUGCUUUCAACUGUGGUCUGUAGUGAGGGCCAAAUGGUAUUAAAAUUUGUUCUUCCUUGUCAUUCUGUUCUAAAUAAUAUCUAUUAGGAUGAUUAGUACCAAAGAAGCGAUUUUGCUCUGUUGUCCAGGCUGGAGUGCAGUGAAGUAAUCAUGGUUCAUUGCAGCCUCUGUGUCCCGAGUUCAGGUGGUCUUUCCACCUCAGCCUCCAAAGUAGCUGAGACUACAAAUGCAUGCUACCAUGCGUGGCUAAUUUUUAAAAAUUUUUUUAUAGUGAUAGGGUCUCACUAUGUUGCCCAGGAGUUCACUGGGCCCGAAUGAUCCUCUUGCCUCAGCCUCUCAGAAUGCUGGGAUUACGUACAUGAGCCACUGCCACUAGCUGUGAUCUGUAUUUUUCUGUUGCUCACAUACCACUGUAGUGCUAACCAUUUACUGAGUUCUAGUUCUAAUCAUUUGUGGGGUAGAGACUUUGGGUAAUAUGUUCUAUUCCUAAACCCUUGCUUUUGGAUUGUGAAAAUGGAAGACUAUUUAGAAGUGGAAACAAUUGAGUUGCAAUCUUUAUACACCUAAACCAGGACCAGAAAUCCUGGAUUGCUGUGUUUGCCAUUUGUUCUUAAAAAUAAUAAAUCCUAGAACAUAUUUUAUUACCCCAUUAUUACAUAUCAAAAAUUAAAUCUUCCCAAGACAAAUAAAAUAAAUGAAAAGUUAAUUGUGAAUGUAGCUUAUUUCAAAAAUUACACUUAAAUCUAUACCUGAAAAUACUUUUCUUUAGUGAAGAAGACAUCAUUUAAAUGUUUCAUAAAAUUUUAGAAUGAAAAACUUCUUGUAGAUUUAAUUCAUUCUCAUUUUAGAAGAACAGAAUUAAAAUUGCCUCUUUGGUUAAUUUAAAUAUUGAUACUAAUCAUCCUAAUAGAUAUUAUUUAGAACAAAAAGACAAUGAAGAACAAGCUUUAAUACCAUUUGGCUGUCUCUAAAGACCACAGUUGAAAGCACCAACUAUUAAUCUUUUAAUUUUUGGUACAGUAAUUUUCAAAAUGAAUAUUUUAGAUCAGUGAUCCAAUUUAAACUCUGUUAAAUAGCAAGGAAAGCAUGUAAUCAGAAAUAAUUCUUCUGUCACAUUUCAACAUUAAAGUCAAGGCCUUUUACAAACCUUUGAAAAGUAUUUGGGAAUAACCUCAUUAUAUUUUAAAAAAUUCUUUCUUUUUUUUUCAUAGGAUAUACAUGUUAUAUGUCACCUCUCCCUGAGAUCUUUUGUAAUAGAAAGUCUUCAAUGUGUUCGUAAUAAAGAAUUCUAGGUAAUAAAAUUUUAUUUUCUUUUUAAGGAUAUGCUGAAAGUGAGAAAGGGUAUUAAAGUAUUAAACUACUCAAAGAACACCCCAAAAUAUUUUCAUUAAUAAGAUUAAUAAUUUGCACUGCAUUUAUCUGAAAAAAAACACACACACACAGUGCUACAUUAAUCAGUUUGGCAGUUGUUUUAAAAGGAUAAUGUCUUCUGAACAACCUAUUAGAAGAGAGAGACAUGAUGCAGACUUGGAGGUUCAGCAUUUGGAAACCAUCCAGAGCAUCACACUGAGGAGCCAUAGAGUAGGCUUUUGUGGCAUAGAGCCCUAGAAUUUUUGGAAAUUCUAACUUGAGUGCCAAAAGAGCUGUGGUUAUCUGUGAUUUCAGAGGCAGCUCACUGGGUUCUCUAUGAUGUAGAAAGCUUGAACCCUAGUUCUCACGGAGAUCAUCAGCUCCACAAAAUUGGCUGGAGAAUUAUUAUUAUUGCAGAGAAGGAGGGCAAUUGUCAGGGUUUGUUAGUCUGUAUUCUAUAAUAGUCUGUGUAUUGGUCAGGGUUCGCCAGAGAAAAAGAACACACAGGAGAUACACACACACACACACACACACACACACACACACACACACACGCUUUAAUAUGAGGAAUUGUCUCAAGAAAUAUGGAGGCCAAGAAGUCUCAGAAUCUAUAGUUUGGGCAAGCUGGAUAUUCAGAAGUGAAAAUGGUUUAGAUCCUGUUUAAGUCCAAAGGCCUGAGAACCAGAAGAGCCAAUGACAUAAGUUCUAACCUGAAAGCCAAAGGUCCAAGACCCAAGAAGAGCCAAAGUUUUAGUCAAUGUUUAAAAGCAGAAAAAGAUUGAUGUCCAACCUCAGGCACUCAGGCAGGAGUUUCCUCUUACUUGUGGGAGGGUCAACAUUUGUUGUUCUCUUCAGGUCUUCAACUAAUUGAGGCCCACCACAGUGGGGAAAGCCAUCAGCUUUACAUAGUCUACUGAUUCAAAUGUUAAUCUUAUCCAGAGUAAUGUUCUCCCAAAUGUCUGGGUACCCCAGGUCCACUCAAGUUAACAUAUAAAAUUAACCAUCCCAAUCUAAUAGCUUUUCUCACAUUGCCUAAAAGAUGUUGAAACUACCUGUAAUAUACAUUUUUUUUUUCAGGCGAGAUUUAAGAGAAUUAAAAGCAGGGCUUUAUGUGGAACCAUUAAUGUUUCAGACUUGGAAGAGAUAUUUUAAAUUUCUAGUACAACUCUUUCACUUUAUCUUCAUAAAGAUGACUCUCUUGGGGCCUCUGAGGUAAUGAGAGGCCACCCUGGUCCCUGACCUCCUGUUCUUAGACACGGGCUUCUCCUACAGUCCACAUAACCCCUCUCAAAGCCAAGGAAGGCAUUACCUGAGGGGAGGCUUGUUUUCUCCUUCAUCUGCUUCUGCUCUUUAUUCUGCUCCUCUUCGUCAUUUACCCUAAGCUCUUCCUCCUAUUGUUCCUCUUACUUUUCUCACUCCUUGUCUUAUUCUUCCUGUUACCCCUCUCUCUCUUCUCUUUCUCCUUCUUUACCUCUUCCUCUUUCUUCUAUUCUUCUUUCUGCUCUUCCUGCUCUGUCUUCUAUUUUCUAGUGUGGGAUAAACUUAAUAAAUAGGUUGCCCUAGGUUGUUCUUUCUUCAGCCUGAAGGUGAAGGCGUCAUCUCCCUGUGAUGGCUCCUCUUUUGAGCCAUGCUCCCAGAGACAUAAUCAAAAUAAGAGUGUACCUGAGGACUUGGUAACUGCAUAUGUAAUGCCCCUUUGGGUGACACUUGACAUCUCGUAGGAAAGAUUGUUCAGGGCAUUUGCUCAGUAAGAUUCACAUUUAAUUAGCACAUACUAUGUGUUGGGUUCUAUGUUAGGCACUUCAGCUCAGGUAGGAGGAAGACAGAGGUCUGGGAAGGUCUAUCAUAAAAAGGUAGUAACCUUUUCAGCAAAGGACAUAAAAAUUGUAGACUAGAAAUAAUGAUAAUGAUGCUUAUAUAAGUUUUUCAAGUUUUGUAUUAUCUCAAUGUUUGGCAUUAAUUAAUUUCAUUUUUAUUAUUGCACUUCUUAUUGUGUUAUUAUUGCAUCUUUGACUACAUACAUUAAUUCACUUGUUUAUUCAUUCAACUACUUACCCAAUUAUCUAACAUUUACUUAGCUCCUACUCGGUUCUGGGCAUGUAUUAGUAAAUAAGACAGAUUUUUCUCUCAAAAAGAGAUAACAUAGCAUAAGGACUAAAAAUUUGGACUCUGAAAUUGGAUAGCUGGUGUCUGAGGCCCAGUUUUUGUCACUCACUUAGACAUUAUCUUUUCUAAGCCUAAUUUGCUCAUUGUAAAGUGGGGAUUAUUAAUAGGACUAUGGUGAAGAUUGAAGGCAUUUUGGGAGUGCUUGGCACAUAGUAAGCACUCAUGAAUGUUCAUCAUUGUUAUUACUGACAGCUGGCUCAGAGAUUUAUGGAAGUAAACCAACAACAGAGAACAGUGUAACAAAUGUCAGUGCAGGGAAGCACUUGGCCCAGCUAGAGAGAUCACCGAAGGCUUUCUGGAAGACAUGGCACUUGAGUCAAGACCAUAGGCAGAAUAGGAGCUACCUGGCAAGGAGUCUAGAAGAGGAUAUUUCAGGCAAAGAAGAACAGCACUUAAAAACGCAAUAGGCUAUAAGAGCUCGAGGUAGGUGUAUUAGUCUGUUCUUACACUGCUAUAAAGAAAUAUGUGAGACUGGGUAAUUUAUAAAGAAAAAAGGUAUAAUUGACUCAUGGUUCCACAGGCUGUACAGGAAUCAUGAUGCUGGCAUCUGCUCAGCUUCUGGGGAGGCCUCAGGAAAACUUACAAUCAUGGUGGAAGGCAAAGGGGGAGCAGAGCAGGAGGAAGUGGGGCAGGGAGGUGCCACACACUUUUAAACAACCAGAUCUCAUGAGAACCCUUUCAUGAGAGCAGCACGAAAGGGGGAAAUCCACACCCAUGAUCCAAUCACCUCUCACCACACCCCACCUCCAACAUUGGGGAUUACAAUUUGACAUGAGAUUUAGGUGGGGACACAGAAGCAAACCACAUCACAGGGCUUGGAGAAGAGCACUGAAGAAGAAAGGUUUUAUUUAUUAAACGGCAGAAGUAGACUUUGUAGGGGUCAGUGUCAGGACAGUUCAAUCACCCAUUUUACAGAUGAGAAGACUGAGGCCCAGCUGCCUCUGUUGAACUGAAUAGACUAAGGUCAAACAGCUGGUGAAUGAGAGAGCUCAUUUACACCACAGCCUCCAUCACCAGUGCAGAGUCAAGUGGGAGAACAGCCUGCUGUAAGUGUACAUGUAGGAGGCAAGAGUUUAUGUAGAGAAGUUUGUGUCAGCAGCUAUGUCUCUCCAUGACUUAUACUCUUUCUUAACUAGCUGUGUAUUUAAGGUUAUUAAAGCAAGUAUUUUGGGGUGUAUUAUUGUUAGACACCCGUCUUAAUCCAUUUUGUGUUGCUAUAACAGAAUACCUGAGGCUGAGUAAUUUAUAAAAAAAAGAGGUGUAUUUAGCUUACAGUUCUGCAGGCUGGAAAGUUCAAGAAGCAUGGCACUGGCACCUGAUCAGCUUUCGGUGAGGGCUUUUGUACUGCAUCAGAACAUGGUGAAGAAGGACAAAGGGGAAGCAGACACAUCUGAAGAGGGACUGAACCCAAGGUGUGUCCUGGUUUUACAACAACCCACUCUUGAGGGAACUAAUGCAUUCCUUUGAGAACUAGUCCUGUCUUGCCAGAGUAAUUCUCUCACUACCACAAGAACAACACUAAGCCAUUCAUGAAGGAUCUGCUUCCAUGACCCAAAUACCUCCCACUAGGACCCACCUCCCAAUACCAUUAUAUUGGGAAUCAAAUUUUAACAUGAGCUUUGGUGCGGACGAACAAACCAUAUCCAAACUAUAGCAAAGACAUUAAUGCUUCUUCUUGUCAGAGCUCAUCCACACUUGAUACUACCACUUCUCCUCAUUGCAAAUCUAAGAACUAUUUGGUUGAUACAAAAGUAAUCAUGGUUUUGCCAUUAAAAGUAAUGGCAAAAACUGCAAUUACUUUUGCACCAACCUAAUAUUUGCAAAUUCUUAGCCAUGUGAUCUGGUCAAGAUGAAGAAAGGGAUCUGAAGAAUUAAUGAUUUGUAAUCAAGAAAAAAAAGUCCAAAUCUAGAUAUACUGUUUUGCAGGUCCCAAUUUCUCAUCAUUAGUAUUUAUUUAGUCCAUUAGUUGUCAUUCGACAAAUGGAGCUUUCAUUAACUCUGGGUCCUAGGACCUAGAGAUACCAUAAUGACCAAGAUGAACUGCCCCACCCCACAGUGAUGGUGGUAAUGUGACAAGUAAAUAAGUGACUGCAAAAUAGUGUGACAAAUGCAAUAAAUGUCCUAAGAUGGACAUUUAUUCUGAUCCAGAGCAUCAAGAAGGGCUUUCUAGAGGCACUAAUUUCAGCAUUGAGCUUUGAAAUAGAUAGAGGUUAGAAGUUACUGAGCUGGAAAGAACUGGUAGUUAGGCAAAGGAGGCCUGGGGAACAUCAGGGCAGUGGCCUGGAGGCAAGAGGCUGUAACUGAGGAAUCAGAAGAGAGGCAGUGUGGCUAGAAUGUAGGGGAUUCAUUCAUCUCUGGAGAGGAGGCUGGAGAGGUAUAGAAGCCGGAUAUGAAGGGCCAUGUGAACCUGAGAAAGGAAUUGAAAGUUAAUUCUAUGAACGCUGUGGGAUCAUACAGUAUUUAUGCAGGGGAGAAAAAGAUCAGACAUUGGAUUUUAGAAAGGUCCUUCCUGCUGCAGUGCUGUCACAGAAGAGAUUGCCAUAACCAAGAGUGGGUGCAGGAAUAUCAGCUUGGGGACUUUUAUAAGGGUGGCCUAGGGAUGAAGGGAAGAGGAAGGAUGGGAGUGGUAAUUAGCUUAAUAACUGGGUGUGUGGGUGGAUGAGAGAGAGAAAUCAUAGAUAAAUUGCACUCACCAGAUGCUACUGAAUCUAUCUGUCUCUGCUAGUCCUGUUCACAGAAACAGGGGACACUGGGAGAGGGAGAGCCUGAGGAUAUAAAGAGGAUCAGAAGACAAAGGAGUGAGUUUAGCUUUAGACCAUUUGAAUUUGAAAUGUUUGUGGGUCACCCAGGUGUGUCUGUCCAGCAUAAAGCAGGCCAGUGAAAAUAUCAGUGUAUGUAUGUAAACUUAAUAACUAGUUAUUUUAUGAAUACACUCCCUGGAUAAGGAGAUCAAAUUCCACCUAGGAGCUGGGUGGUUUCUCAGCACUCAAAGCAGUCCCAACAGGCUCUAAUUGAGCUCAGAGUGCCUAGCCAGGCACUGGGGGAACGGGAGAAGGAGGAGCAGAGAAAAAUCUAGAUGGGGCUGCUUAUGUAAGGCCAGAAUUCAGAGAGAAAGCCAGAGGCACUGCGGAAUCUCUUCUUCAUAGCCAUGGGAAUAAUAGUAAAAUUGUUCAUGAAACACCAAGUUGCCUGAGUAGUAAAUGAACUAAUUUUGUGAUAAGCUCAAAGGACACAGAAGCUAAAAACAUGGACUUUUGAGCAGAUAAUUCUGGUUUAAACUCCCAUUUCUGUCCCUUUCUAUAUGACCUUAGGGAAAUUACUCACUCUCUCUAAGCCUCAGUUUCUUUAUCUUUAAAUGAGAUGACACUACCUAGUUAGAUAUAAAAACACCUAGCUUAUUGGAUUGCUGAAGGAUUAAGUGAAAUAUCGUAUAUGAAGUUCUGGCAAGUUUCAGUGUUUGUCAAUAGUGAGCCCUCAAUCUCUGGUAGUUACUGUUGCUGUUAUGAGAUAUCCCAAGAAGGCAAAUAUCCUUGUUGCCAUGUUUACUACAGCAGCAGGGAGGAAAGGAGCAGACAGCCACACCCAUUCACAUAUAUGUGUAUAGAACAUGUGACUAUACACGUAUUUAUAAUAACAGAAGACUUCAUUAUUUUCUUGCUUUAAAACCAUAACCAUGUAAUUUUAUGAAAAUAUGAAAGAAGAGUGCAUCCCGUUGCUAAGUGAUAUGCUCAUGUAAUUACUGGGGAAACAGAUGGCCAAUCAAUAGUAGACAGCUAAUUGCCUUACAAAUAGAUUUAGUUAAAGAUUGGAAAUGAUGAUAAAAGUGUGUUGUCCUUAUGAUAGUGAUAUUAAGGCGGUUCAUGGUCAAUUAUAAUAAUAUAAAUCAUAUUGAAAAGAGCAUCUUAUUUCUACUUUUAAGCUAAUAGGAAGCCACUGCUUUCUGUAUUGUUGAGUCAAGUUUUGGAAGAAAAAUGGAACCACUCAUUGUGCUAGACAAAUGCUUUAUUCUAGGCUACUUUUUCUUCCAAGGAAGAUGAGCAUUUGAAAAGUAAUUAUCUAUCCAUUCAUUCUGCCAACCAACAUUUAGUGAACAUCCACUAUUAUACUUUCAUGCAAACUUUCUUCUUCCAUACUCUACCUUCUUCCUCCACUUUGCUCCUAAAAAGUCCAAACUACCAGAAAAAUGUAGAAGUGGGCACCCUGUGUACACACAUGGCUGAUGACAAGGUAAAUUGGAACAAUAUUUUAAGAAAACAGUAUGCUUCUGUCAAUCAAGCACAAAAGUAUUAUGCCAGUUGGUCCAGGAAUCUCACCUCCUUGGAAACUAUGUGGAGAAAAUAAUUCAGCCAAAGAAAAAAGCUGCUUGUAUGAAGAUAUUUAUUGUGGAAUUAUUUAUAAGAAUAAAUUGGAAACAAAUUAUAUGUCCAAUGCUAAAUAAUAAUUAAGAAUGACAAUCCCAUUUAUGAAUUCUACAUAACAUUAUGCAGCUAUUUAUAAUGUUUACAGUCUUCUUAGAAAUCUGAACAAAAUUUAUGAUCUCAUAAAUAAGGUAGUUUGCAAGAAUUCACCAGUUCUAUGUUUAUAGCUAUGCAAAGAAUAAGUAUAAAAUAGGAAAAUGACUGAGAAAGAGCAAACAAAACUGAAAAUAAUUGUGUUAGAAGAGUGGAAUAUUCUUUUUUCAGUCUUCAACAACUCAUUUUGAUAUUCUUUUAUGAUAUAUUAAAUGUGAACACCACAAAGAAUUGUUCUGUAUGUAGUCAAAAUCCAAGAUGGCACCUUCCAAACACCAAAUAAAAAGCCUUCCUUGCUUUUAGAAUUCAAGUAAUCUUAGAGCAAUAAAUAGUUGUUUCUCCAUGUCUUAUCUUCCUUGUUUUGUACUGUGAGAGGCAUUUACAAGUAUAUUGAAUUUCUCUUGCUUAUGAAUUCAACUGCUGCUGCUUUUCAACAAACAGCCUUAAUCCUUUGUUUGGCUGUCAUAGUUGCUACUGCAGGAAUUAUGAUGCUGCCAACAGAGAAUUCAGGAGAUAAAAUGAAGAGGUUUGUAAAUGCCAGUACACUUGCACCCUUUUCUUGAUAUUACCAACUGUACAUAUGUGUAUAUCUCUUUCUAUAUAUUUGUCCUAUUAAACUCCAACCUUGUUCAGUGCGUGGACCAUAAGGUUUAUUUAAUCUGAAAACAUGCUUUGCAUGCUAUAAUUAUUAUUACAGAAGAAAAUAAAUGUACUCACUAAUCAGAAUAUCCACUAGCAAUGAAGAAGGAAAAUGCUGCCGUCCUUGGGGGUAGAUUUCUGUAAUGUUCCUCAUGCCCAUGCCAGAAUUUUGUUUUCUUUUUCUUUCAACUUCCUAGACCCUAAUUUCCAAUGUCAGAAUAGUUUCCCAGUCAGAAUUGGGUAGGAGAGAUGGAAGUCUGUGCUGGCUGCUUUUAUAAAUAUUAUGUGGUUGUUAUUUUAGUGUGAUUAAAAAAGAAAACAAUGACUAAAAUUAUUCGUAAUGAUUCAUAUUAACAUUGUGAGGCAAUAAUUAUAUUUCUAUAUUUCUAUAUAUAUAUAUAUUUUGAGAGAGAGUCUCACUCUGUCACUCAGGCUGGAGUGCAGCGGUGCGAUCUCGGCUCAUUGCAACCUCUGCCUCUGGGGUUCAAGUGAUUCUCACGCCUCAGCCUCCCAAGUAGUUGGGACUAUAGGCGCACUCCACCACACCUAGCUAAUUUUGUAUUUUUGGUAGAGAUGGGGGUUUUGCCAUGUUGGCCAGGCUGAUCUCAAACUCUUGACCUCAGGUGAUCCACCAGCCUCAGCCACCCAAACUGCUGGGAUUAUAGGGGUGAGCCACCAUACCCAGCUGGGAAUAACUAUAUUUCUAAAUGACAGAGCUUCAUUAGGGUUAGACAUUUGUGAGGAACAUGCUUGCUUGCUGGAGAUGCUUGGCUUGCAGGUGCCUGCCAUUUGCAUGUUGUAUAGUGCACAUCUGAACUUUGGAGCCACUCUUACCAUCUGCCAUAAACUGAAAGGUGCAAUUUCCAAAACUGUUUUCCUUAAGACCCAGGAUCUGAAAAAGAUUAUUUGAAAAUCCCCUUAGAGAUGGAAAGAAAGAAAAAAAGAAAGCAAUGGUCCUUUUGCUUGUAUAUUAUUCUAUUCAAUCUUCACUUUAGAUAAAAAUCACUGUAGGCCUUUGGUGACAGAAACAGAUGUCUCAAAGAGGACUGGAUCACACAAAGUCAGAUUUCACCUGGGUAGAAAGCAUUCUGCAUUGACAACCAUCUGGGUUUCAACUAGAUGAAAUGUGAUGAUGCAGAAUAUUGUCUCAUAAUACUUAUGGAUGUUUGGCUAAUAGCACCAGUGAUGACUGACCAAGGCCACUCACAGGGAGCAGCUGCACAAAUGUAUGUACGUAGAUGUCUGUGUGUCUGUGUAUAUGUAGGCAUGUGUGUAUAUAUAAGCAUGGGCAUGUUUAUAUGCAUGUUUAUAUGCAUAUACACAUAGGUGUGUAUGUGUGUACAUAUGAGUGUGCAUGUACAUACACAUAUAUACAUGUAUGCGUAUGUAUAUGUGUGUAUAUAUGUGUGUAUGCAUGUGUAUGUAUGUGCACUAAAUGUUUUUAAUUACAUUUGCCAAAUGCAUUUUUGGUUUAUAUAACUUCCCACAUUUCCAAGGUUACUGACAUAAUUUAACACCCAACAUAUGUCAGAGUUGUUAUUUUGACUUUUUUAAAAUUAAAGAUGCAAUUUCUAAAUGAGUGCAGGAGACUUCAGAAAUAUUACUGUGCUAAAUUUCAAGCUCCUGAAACUUUAAAACUCAGAAAAGAAGGGUGAGAUCUUGGACAUAAGCUCCUGUUUUCAUUUGCUUAAAAUGCGAAUAGAUUGCAAGACAUCCAGGAUCCACAUUUCCCCAGUAAAGGCCUUGAGUCGUAAGACACUAUCACAGGCAAAGGCAGUUUCCCUGCCAGCCCCCUCAUUUCACAGAAUACAAGUGUAGCCCUUGUGUAGGUAAGCGAGUCCAGAGUGUCCUGGCUUCUCGUGGGCCUCUUUAUUGCAAACAGAGUAGACUUUUAAAUAAGCCAGAGCCUUAGCUUCCAGAAAGAUAAUCCGAGGCAUGGAAAGGAUGGUUAGUCUGAUGAGCUAAUUUUAGGACCUGGAAUCUCAGCAGCAUCCUUUUAAUAUUGCAGCACACGCUGCUGUUUCCAGGGCCUCUUCAGGAUCUCCUUAAAUAAAUUAGGAUCUAAAGAGCCCUCCUGUUUCCUUAGAGUUAAGCUAAUGCUGCCAGCAGUGCCAUUUUGGUUCCUUAGUUGCUCUCUGUAGGCCUCAUAAAGCCCUUUCUCAACCCUCCACAUGCUGGGCAAAGCACAACCUGGUGGUCGUGGCUCAGACACCAUUUAAUUUCCUUCUCAAACCAUCUUGUUUUAUGUAAGUUGACCUUUUCAUGACUGUAAAAUUUCCUCAUUAGAAAAUGACAGGCUCUCUGGGAUUGCAAACCUUUCCUGAUAACACUCUGUAUAAAGGUGUCUGUGAAAGAUUUUUCUCACUUAAAAAUGAAAAGAGACCCUUUUGUCUACUCCACUAGCAGCUUUCAGAGCACACAGACAAUCCACUUGAAUUUUGUUUAAAAAAAAACAAACAAACAGGAAACCUUCACUUGUUGGGGCAGCCAGUAAGGGGGUGUCAGAGAUGAAUCUGAAGGAUCUGGUUUUAAGAAACUCAGAAUCAUUAUCCACUUCAUUUUCAGAGUACCCAUUCUCUGUUAAGUAUGUAACAUAUGCCAUUGCUAGAAUUUCCUACAGCUCUACAGGGGUUCCUAUUACAGUUGAGGAAACUUGGAUUCAGAAAGGUCCAGAGGCUUGCCCAAGGUCAUUGAGCAGGAGAGUGACAGAGCUAGUGCUUCAACCUAGGUCCUUGUGGCUCUGUUCUUUCCACUGCAUCAUUCUGCCUCUCAAGGCAAUACUUGCUCAAAAAAAUAAAUUUCAGACAGACAUGCUGCAGAUGCCUUAGUUUGCAUGGAAUACACACUGUUAACAACAGUUAUUGGAUUGGAGAAUUACUAGGGUUUCUGACCUCAGCAACUGGAGUACCUUCGCUACAGUACCAGUCCUGAGCCAGGCUGCUAGGAUUCAAACCCUUUCAUGGCCCCUGGCUGGCUGUGGCAUUCAGGGUUGUCACUUCUCUGGAGUGAGGUCUCUUGAGCAGAAACAUGAGCACAUGUAACAUAAUACCUUCCUCACAGCAUUGUUGUAAGGAGUAAAUGAGAGAAUGCUUGCAAAAUGCUGUUGGGUAAUUAAUACAAAGUAGCUGUUAUUAUUACCAAAAUGACAUAGAAAUGUUGCUGCCUCCCUGCCCAUAGGAAAAAACUGGGGGAGCAAAUCAACUUGUGACUUGCAAGAAACCUCAAAUAAUAGCACCAAAUAAAGAAGGCUGAUGUACACAAUUUGCCAACAGUGGAGGGCAUUGCGACAAAAACCGCCCGACAGGAAGGCCGAGGCUGUCACAUCCCAUUACUCUGGAGCUGUGACUUCAUGCUGACUCAGCCAAAGGCAGGCAGUAAUCACAGCCAAGUUUAUAUGCUCAGAAUUGAUGUGGCCAUAUUUCCACAUUCUCAAAAGCAAAGCCAAGAGAAAACGGCGAUCAGAAAGUUUUUAUGGGCCUCAUCAUGAAAUGGUGACAGCUCCAGCUUAUUGAUUUGCCUUUAGUUAACCUCUGUAAUUCGAAGUGAUCACCCUGCCAAAAAUGAAGGUUUAUCAAGGGAAUCCUUUUUACCUUUUGGUCUUUUUGGAACAAAGACCUUGUCCGUUCUUCUUUAUUCUAUAGAGUAAUUGAUUUGGGUUGAUGGUAAGUGUUCAGAUGAGAUUUCUGGAGGACAUUUAUCUGAGUCGUCCCAAACAAUCAUUAUUGUUUAUGUUGAUGAUGUUUUUGCCUCACCCAUUCAGAAAUGCUGCAGUACAUUCAUGGGCGCAGUCAAAGCAGUGUUUUCAAUUAUCUUUUUGUAUUUCUAAUUGGUAGAAAUAAAUUAGAAGACAUGUAUUUGACUACUAUUCUGCACCAGCAAAUCCAUUUUUUUUUUAAUGAUGCUAAUUGUGGUUGUCAUGGAAACCCUGAAAGUAGUUAGGCUGAAUUGCUCAAUGUAUUUCUUUUUUUCUCUGUAAGUGAUUAUUUCUUUGGCUGAUAUUGAAGUUCUUCUAGAAAGCUAUUAUGCAUACGCUCACAAGACAUUUACUCUAAGUUAAGAUGCUCGAUAAAUCUGUUACACCAAUUAUAUUUGUACUGUGGUUAUGAGAAUCAAUAUGCUUGAGAUGUAAACUGAUCACCUAGAAAAGUGAAUAAACCAGUUGGCUUGUUUUUUUAUUUUAUUUUCCUGAAAGUAGUGAUGUAAUGCCUAGAUGAUUUUCAAAAAUAUUCUGCUUGCUUUAAACUUUUGGUAUUAUUUAAUGUCUGUGUGUAUGCUUUUCAAAUGUCAUUUUGCUGUAACUUUUCUGAAAAAUGUCAAAAUUAUAUUGAAGAGUCAUGUCUGCUUCUUGUUAAUCCUGUUGGCAGAUUUCAGGGGGAAAAGAGAUAUACAUGGAGGAUAUAGGCUGAGGAAGAAAGCCUCUGAGUCUAAAUGGUCGUAGAUAAAAUACUAGAUGCAUCAUUUAUUAAUUGUGCAUACUUAACCUGGGUUGUAGUCUUCACAUGUAAAAUGAGAGUCAUAACCUCAUUGGGUUGUUUAAAGAUGAAGCGUAACUAUACAUGUCAUACUGCUCAUAUGGUGGCAGGCAUAUAAAAGAUGCCCUAGAAAUUUUACUCUUGUUCCUGCCUAAGUCUCCCUAAUCAACCUUCCCUUCUGCACCCUCUCACAGGGACUCACUCCUGGGUUUCUGGAAUUAUGUGUUUGGAUUGAAGGGAGAGAAUGUUUGGCUAGCAGAACCUCAAUAAAUUUUUAGCAUCCUUACAGCAUCCCCAUGUUAUGGGAAAAAAGCAAUGUUCCGGGACAAGCCUGACCUGGAAAGAGAAUCUUCACAAGGAUUAAAAAAGUUCCAUCACAGUAACUUCCAACCAAAUACCCUCUCAAGAAAUUUAUUCUUCCAAAACAAAUAUCCUGUUGAUUGGAUGAUUGAGUUGGGGUGGGGAGAGAGCUCUUUAGGAGCAAUAGUCAAUAGUUCACCCUUGCAUGUGUGAGUUUUAGAAUUUGUACAACCACACUUUUUUUUUUUUUUUUUUUUUUUUUGCAACAAGGUCCUCACUCUGUCUCUCAGGCUGGAGUGCAGUGGCAGGACCAUGGUUCACUGCAGCCUGGACCUCCUAGGCUCAAGUGAUCCUCCUGCCUUAGCCUCCUAAGUAGCUGGGACCACAGGUGCAUGCCACCACACCCAGCUAAUUCUUAAAUUUUUUUGUAGAGAUUGAGGGGGAUGUUGCUAUGUUGCCCAGGCUGAUGUCAAACUCUUGGCCUCAAAGUGAUCCCUCUACCCUGGCCUCCCAAAGUGCUGGGAUUACAGGUGUGAGCCACUGCACCCAGCCAACCAAACAUUUUUAAUGCAGUAAUAGAGCUACUUUCUCAGCUCAUUACACCGGUACAGAAUCUUUCUUCUUGGGAUCAUGAAGUAUUGGUAGCAUGUCUUUAUCUUACUAAAUGAGUCUUUAUCUUACUAAAUCUUCCCUACUACAUAGUUGGUUCAUAUUAUGAGUCUUAUUUAUUUUAAUUAAAGUGAAUAUAGAGGCAAAUUUAUGUUUCCAACGUACCUCGUAUAUGCCUCAGUUAUAGCACUUACCACGUGGCAUUAUAAUUGUUUGCAUAUAUUCAUCCCCCAUAGAUUAAACAAUUUAGAGAUGACUGCAUUCUCUGAAACCAAACAAAACUAAAAUUUGAAAUCUUGAGUAUCAAGUAAGUUAGGCUCUUCACUCAUUCAGUGAUUAUUUAAUGAGCUUCUACUAUUUUCCCUGUGCUAGACUAACUGUUGGGAAUUCAGGAGUGAAUGUGGCAGACAUGUUUCCUUCCUCAUUAGGCAAUGAGGCUCACAUCUACUAUGGCAGCGGCUAAGUGCUGUCAGCAGUGAACUUCCAGCUCUGUAGCACUUAGUGGCUCCGUAAGUGGAGCUUGGGACUGCCCAAGAGUCAAGUAAGUCUUCCUGAAGGCAACGGCUUUGAAGGAGAGAACUGAAGACACACAACUUAGAGGGUUAGGGAGAGUGUUCCAAACCGAGGGAAAAACAAAUGUAAAUGGACACAGAGGUCAAAAGACAGUUUCUUGAGUUCUUGUGCCUACACGUUCCUAGGGAAGGGUCUCAACCCCUGCAUGAAACAUACACUGAUGACAUGAAUUUGCUGUUUUUAAGGAGGAGAUUGCAUUUGUUACAUAAACUGCAGCAUCAGCAGCUUGGGAUCUGUGUUUCUUAGGCUGAGGUGACACCACUGAGGGUCCCUGAUGGUGCAGCCUUUCACGAUGACUUUGCAGCAACACAGCACCCUCCCAGUGCACCCUGGAAUGGAGCCCUGGGAGGGAACAAAGACACCCUCUGGGGUUUCUUUGAGAUUUUUGAUUUGCUUAUCUCUUCCUCCAGACUUCAAACACAUUUUGGUUUCUCUAGGGGUUGCUCAUUCAAAUGCCAAGUAGACAAGGAUUUGAACUAAUUAUCUAAUUUUAAAUAAGGUGUAGUAGGGACAUAUAGAAUUAAGGGAAUUAUAGGAGACAGCAUGGUGUUUGGAGUCCAGUCAGAGAAAUCUGGUUUUGCCUCCUGAUUCCUUCUCUCAGGUCUAGGUAAACUUCAGCAUGUUCUUCUUCCCAUCUGUCAGGCAGGGAUAGGAACACCUGCCCAGAGGGCUGCUGGAAGAUGGAGUGAAAAUGACACUUAUUACCUGUUUAAAGUGGUGCCUGGCAUCAUCCACAAGCGAGAAUUAGGAAAGAGAGUAAUCUUUAGAAGCCUCAGCUUCAUUGCUUUUUUUUUUUUUUUUUACUGCUGUAUUUUCCUUUCUUUUUUAUUUUUUAAAGCAGCUUUAUUGGAACAUAAUUUACAUACCAUCACAUCCAUUUUGAGUGUAUAAUUCAAUGAAUUUUAGUAUAUUUAGAGUUGUGUGAUCAACACCACAAUCUAAUUUUAGGACUUUCCCAUCAUCCUAGAAAGAAAAUAUUUGAAUUUUUUUGUGUCUAUGAAUUCUAAACUAUGCUCAGGAAAUAUUCAAUUUAAGGACCCAAGCUAAUCAUCAUGUUUACUUAAUAACCACAGGUUGUCAUAUAUCAUCAUAUUGUGAUAAUUAUCAUCAAGAAUGUUAACUAUUUAAGUAUGUUACAACUUUAGAUAAUUUACUUGUUGAUAUUAUUAAUAAAUGUUAAAAUGGUCUUUUUUUGGGCAAACAACAGUUAAUGAUGACUGGUGGUACUUAUUCAAAUAAAUAAAAAAAGUCUUGCCAUAAAACCUUUGGGAAAAAUAUGUUUUUUAGUUUGUGCUGUUAUGAAAAAGUAGCUAGUCAAAUAAUCUUGAAUAUAUUACCAGAAACUCAUUGGAAAGGGCAGAGUUAAGUAGAGAGGCCAUGGGAUUAGGCACGAGGGCUCUAUAGAGCCAGAGUUCAAACCCAAUUCAGCCAGUUAUAGGCUGUGGAAUAUGAAACCAAAUGCCUUAACUCUCUGGCCCACAGUCUCUUCAUUUGUAAAAUAGAGGUAAUAGUAGGUGUCUCGUAGGGUUGCAGGAAUUAACUUAUGAUAUAUGUAAAGCCAUUAGUAUUGCAGCUGGCAUACAGUAAGUGUUCAAUAAAUCACUGCUGGAAUUUUAUUGAGUGUAGACUCCCAGGGAAUUGAUAAAAGGGACCAUUUAUUAAAGUUUAAGAACACAUUAGGAAAAGUAGAGAAAGAGGUUGCUUUCGUCUUAAGUAGGGAAUCAAAAAAGCCCCCGCUCUGACUGGAAAAUGACAGUUUUUAAAGAACUAAAUAAUAAUAACCCUUGAUGUGUAUUCUUUGUGACAUAGAGAUAGAGCUAUUGCACUGUAAUCUGAUUUUGUUCUUUUAGCUAUGAGGAGAGGAGAUGAGAGAGACCAAAGAGACAGCCGAUCUUGCUAGGAGAAAGGCUCCUAGACAGACACCCUGAAGCCUUUCCUUUACUUAGGUUUAUUGACACAGGGAGGGGGUCAUCCAUCUGCAGCUGGGCCCAAAAAAUGCCAGGAAUAGCCACAAAAGGCUGGAGACCAUGACUGGCAGUUUGAAUGUCAUCCUUGCUCCUGGCUGUAGUGUGGCUGGUGCAUAGUUGGGGGUGAGGAUAUUAACACGAAAACUAGUGGAUUCAGAACAAGUGGGAUGGCCUGGUUCCCAGGGGUCUUCAGGCCACAUGGUCACUUGCAGGAUUGAAUGAAGAGGUGAUAUUGACUAGGGCUGAUGCCCUGUGAUUCUGGGGAUUUUGAACAUAGGGCUUGAAUAACAACUCAAAUUAUAGAUGGGGUUGUAAAUGGGAAAGACAACCACAGGAGGAGGUGAGGCAGGCUGAUGCAAUGACGAGAGGCCAGGAACCAGGGUCUGUGGAUAGCUGGCUCUAUCACUCCUAGUUGGUAUUCACAUCCUUUUAAAAUCUGAAGGUGCUUUAAUCUUUCCUGGCCCAUUCUACACCAAGGAGAGCUUUCUAAGCCCCAAGGUGUCCCAGGCUGCCAGAGAAAGUUUAGUUCCAUGUGUCUGUGGUACACAUUAGGAAAAGUAGAGAAAGUCACUUGUGGGACUCCUUGGUUUUCCUUCGGGUUAGAGCUGGAGUUAUCUCUGAAGGCUUGAUGGAAGCUGAUUUCCCAAGAUCCAAAAGCUUUCUUUGUCAGGGCUGGCACCAGGGCUCAGCGCUUUCUUAGACUUCUGGUUCAGCCCUGACAAGGUUUUGAAAAUCAAAUUAAAAAGAGACUAAAUAUAACUUGUAGAAAACCUAGGAGGAAGUGUGCUUACAGACCUAAACUCUAAAAGAUGCAAUCAAGUCCUCUGAAAACCAGAUAAUUGACUUUAAAAGACAAGUGUAGAUGUAUUAGGUGGAAGCAUAUUAGUUCACUUAUUCUUUUUUUCACUUAUUUAUUUUUAUACAAACAUCACCGGUUUUCUAUGAAUGGAAGGUGGCAAAUUAUCUGUGUAAGAAGAUUCAGGUAUAAUCUUCCUUCUCAAUGAGUUUCUGUUCUUGAUCAGGGUUGGCAAACUAUGCCUGGCAGGUCAAAUCCUACCUGCUGACUGUGUUUGUAAAUUGAGCUUUACUGGAAAACAGCCAUGCCCAUUUACUUACCGCUAUUAUAGCUGUUUUCCUGCUAUAAUGACAAAGUAGAGUAGUUGUAAUAGGUAUGGUAUAGCUUGCAAGGCCUGAAACAUUUACUGUUUGGCCCUAUAUAUAAAAAGUUUGCUUCAUCAGCAAGAUGAACAGAUAAAGAAAUGAUUAUAUAUAUAUAUGUAAAUAUAUAUACACACCAUCAUUUAUUGAUAUUAUAUAUCAAUGUGUGUGUAUAUAUAUAUAUUAUAUAUAUAUGUAUACCAUCAUUGUGUGUAUGUGUGUGUGUGUGUGUGUGUGUAUAUAUAUAUAUAUAUCAGGGCCUGGUGAUUGAGGGGAAAAUGGGGAGAUGUUGUUCAGAGAGUACAAACUUUUAUUUAUAAGUUUUGUAGAUCUAAUAUAUAGAAUGGUGACUAUAGUUAACAAUACUGUAUUGUAUACUUAAAAUUUGCUAAGAAAUUAGAUCUUAAAUGUUCCCACCAAAAGACAAAAGACAAAAAAAUAACUAGGUGAGAUGAUAGAUGUGUUAACUAACUUAAUCAUGGGUGAGGUGAUAAAUGUGUUAACUAACUUAAUUGUGGUAAUCAUUUCACUAUAUAUAUACAUAUAUAUAGUGUACAUAUAUAUAUACACAUAUAUAGUGUACUAUAUACACGCAUAUAUAGUGUACUAUAUACACGCAUAUAUAGUGUACAUAUAUACAUGCAUAUAUAGUGUACUAUAUACAUACACAUAUAGUGUACUAUAUACAUACACAUAUAGUGUACUAUAUACAUACACAUAUAGUGUACUAUAUACAUACACAUAUAGUGUACUAUAUACAUACACAUAUAGUGUACUAUAUACAUACACAUAUAGUGUACUAUAUACAUACACAUAUAGUGUACUAUAUACAUACACAUAUAGUGUACUAUAUACAUACAUAUAUAGUGUACUAUAUACAUACAUAUAGUGUACUAUAUACAUACAUAGUGUACUAUAUACAUACAUAGUGUACUAUAUACAUACAUACAUAGUGUACUAUAUACAUACAUACAUAGUGUACUAUAUACAUACAUACAUAGUGUACUAUAUACAUACAUACAUAGUGUACUAUAUACAUACAUACAUAGUGUACUAUAUACAUACAUACAUAGUGUACUAUAUACAUACAUAUAUAGUGUACUAUAUACAUACAUAUAUAGUGUACUAUAUACAUACAUAUAUAUGUAUAUGUAUAUAGUGAAAUGAUUACCACAAUUAAGUUAGUGUGUAUGUAUAUAUACACACACACACACACACAUAUACAUAUAUAUUUAUGUAUGUCAGUAGGGUGGAAAUAGAAAAUGAUGAUGUGGCAUUUUAGGCCAAGAAAGAGACUAUGGAAUGAACCCCCCGACCAACCACCACCACAUAUCUCCUGAAAUCCUGAAGUGACAUGAGACUGCAGAGUGUCUGACAUUGUUGUAUCAAUAUCAAAUAAGAAUGUAAAGACUAAUCUCUAAGCCAAAGGUUUUAUUUGGGAAUACACAAAUGAUAGAAUUGCAAUUUGGGAUGUCCAACAAUGAUAGACUGGAUUAGGAAAAUGUGGCACAUAUACACCAUGGAAUACUAUGCAGCCAUAAAAAAUGAUGAGUUCAUGUCCUUUGUUGGGACAUGGAUGAAAUUGGAAAUCAUCAUUCUCAGUAAACUAUCACAGGAACAAAAAACCAGACACCGCAUAUUCUCACUCAUAGGUGGGAAUUGAACAAUGAGAACACAUGGACACAGGAAGGGGAACAUCACACUCUGGGGACUGUUGUGGGGUGGGGGGAGGGGGGAGGGAUAGCACUGGGAGAUAUACCUAAUGCUACAUGACGAGUUAGUGGGUGCAGCGCACCAGCAUGGCACAUGUAUACAUAUGUAACUAACCUGCACAUUGUGCACAUGUACCCUAAAACUUAAAGUAUAAUAAUAAUAAAUAAAUAAAUUAAAAAAAAAUACCCUAGCACACAUUCGUCAUAACAAAUGUCGGUUGUAAUUGGAAAUCCACAUUAAAUUUGAAUAUUCCCCAAUAGUUUAAAAAGUAAUUAUAAAUAUUCUUAUCUAGCUACAUGUAUUUGUUUAUGUAUUAGCCCAUUCCCAGCAGAUUUUAUUUCAUUCUUUCACAGUAAACAAAUUCAGGGAAUUUUUACUGUAAGUUUUACUUUAGUUCAAAUUCAGUAAGUUUUACUGUAGUUUUCAUGUUAAUGGUUUAUAUGGGUUAAAACUUGUACCCUCAUUCUUAAUUUUGUGGUACUCUAUAGUCACCAUAUGAAAGAAAUAAAGUUACUUUUGGGGAAAUUACUUGAAUAAGGUCAAAUGAGAUCUGCAACUGUGGGAUACACUUUUGUCAACAUUUUAAAAGGCCAACCAGGCUUUGGUCAUUGUACAUUGAUAUGGUAUAGGCCUAUGCUUUGAUUAUAUUCAUUUCAAAGCUCUGUAUUAAUUAGGAAAUAAUGGCUCAUUCUGAGAGGAAAUGAUUAUAUUUGAUUUUGAGAAUUUUGCAUUUGAGCUGAUAAAAUGAGAUACACCAGAAAAAAGUGAAAACAUGAAAAUUAAGCUUCAGUGAAAGUGAAGUAUAGGAAAGUUUUAAAUAUUUUGAUAAUAGAUUAUAUAUCAUAUCAAUAUAUUAUAUAUUCCUCCCUGACCUCAUUCUUGAAAUCUCACCCAAUCCUUGACCUUCCCUGGCAAAGAUCAAAAUUGAGAAAAAGAUCGGGAGUGGCGUAAGUCUCAGGAAUAAAAUAAGAGGGCACCUGAUGUUCACAUUGCUUGGUAAUGAAAAAUAAUAAAGGCUUUUUAAAGCAGUUAAAAAAAAAAAAAAGAUUUGCAAUUUGGGGCACAUGCCCAGACCUGGAUGGCCUCUCAUAAGUCCUAAGACCAAAGGGAAAGUUAGGGUUUUAUUGGGGGAAAGAGGGGGUUAUGCAAGUUGUUUUGAAAGAAAAUUCAUUGGUUCUGGUGAUGUCUUCCAGGAGCUGGUGAGCUCUGAUUGGUGAGUGGUGGCAUUGCUAGGUAAAACUUGUCAUCUUAAAGUCACAGCAGGCUGUUUUCUUGGAAGGGGCUUGCACAACAGUGGAUCUGGUGAGUGUUUUUGUUUAAGAGGCCAACUCUCCUUGUGCUGUUGUCCAUGUGUGACUCAUGUAGCAAUUAAGGCUUGGAAAAGUUUCUUGUAGCAGUUUUUGUUAUUGGGCCAGCCCUGUGUGAGAGCCCUCCCAUCAUGGCCCUGGCUCCAUUUUGCCAGAGUUUGACACGAGUGACUCUAUUUUGAUUCUGACAACUUUCACAGCUGCAACUCUUGUAAAUUCAGAAGGGGCUGAGGGUGAGCUAUGGAACUGGAGAGGCCUGGUGUGUGGGUGACUUCUGUGGUCCUGCCUGGAACAAAGGCCACUGAGUGAGAAAUAGGUUGAUUUACAUCAGCAGUGGGUGGCCCUAUAAUACCAAGGAGGAGUUUCAGAUGAGAAAGACCAAUAUGACAGUAGAAUAGAAGCUCUAGGGACUUAAUUCAGCAGUAAGAAUAGCAGCUAACAUUCUCAUAACAUCUACCAUGGGCAAGGCACUGUUAACAUCUAAUAACUCAUUUAGUCUUCCAAACAGCCCUGUAAGGUGGGUGACAAUUAUUAUCAUCUCCAUUUGACAGAGGGUGAAUCUGAAGAAAGAGAAGUAAAAUAAUUUGUUCAAAUUUCCACCGCAGUGAAGUGACUGCUGGUAUUUGAAUGCAGGCAGUGUCAGGAUCGUGGGCUUACCUAGUAUUCCCAACCACUUCUCUCAGGAAAGGGGUGAGGAGACAAGAUUGAGUAGGUAUCCAAGAAAGACUGAGUCAAUCAUGAAAGUGACUCAGUAGCAGAAAUGACAACUUGAGAUGCAAGUACUACGCAAAAAUAGGGACAUACACUUAUGUAUUUACGCAGUUAUAUCCAUGGUUGUAAAGGUUGAUACCUGCUACAAAUGUGAGUCCUAAAUUUUCCAAUCAAGUUGUAUAGUGAUGGCAGGAUUGCUCACCUCUCAUAAACCAGAAGUCAGAGGCUUAGAGAGAGUUCACUCGGAGGAAAUACCAUGCUCUGAGCUUGAUAUUCACGGGUAUACACAAAUUGGGCAUGUUGAGGUGAGUUAAAUAUGCUGCUUGUUAAAUUAAAGGUGUUCACCGUGCCUUAUUACAUUGAUCAGCUCACCUUGCCUCUUCCCAACUCUAACUUUAGAAGAGGCUGCAUAGGUGGAUGUGUGCUAGAUUACUGAAUAUACUUUCUCUGGUGUUUGCUUUACAUCUUAUCCACAUACUUAAUACAAGUCCAAUAGCAGCUUGCCUGUGUUUAAACCUGUACAGUGUUGAUCAGUUGCACGCCAUUCAGUGAACUAGGCAGGUAUAUGUCUGUUACAGCAAAUACUGCGUUUGAAUGAAGAGAACCAAUGUCUGGGGGGGGAAGUGAAAACUAUCUGAAAUGGGUUAGUUGCCCUAGAAAAUAGAAUUGGGAUUCUUUGUAGAAGAAUAUGCCCACCUUUGGCCCUGAUCUGGGAUUCCAUUUAAAACAAUUUUUUUCUACAGUAUUAUGCCAAAAAGUUUCAAAAUCUAUUUGGCCUUUGCCCAUUCUAAAAUGGACAAAUAAUUUUUUUCUUUUUUUUCCAGAUUUUAUUUGAAACCAUAGAUUAAAAGGAUUUAAAGGAGGGCUACCUAGUUGUUCGUAAAAUAUGUUACUACCUUUUACCUUUUUGAUACUGUAAAUUUACCACGAAAGGUAAAGGAAGUCUGACAGACAUUCCCAGUCAUGAGGAAAUUAUCCUAGAGAGUUGAUGAGGUGGCAAGAGAAGAAGACAUUGCUAUCAUGGCUCACAGAAUAUUGCCAGAGUAGUUGAUGUAUCUUCUUUUCCAACCACAGCCAGUACACUUGUGGGCUUUAAAAAAAUUUAAUUGUAGGUAAUAGAAGAGUUUUGCCAUCUAAAUACAUCGCUGACUUCAUAUUGCAAGUCAAUGGAAAAACUAUACUUUCUUUAUAGAGAUUUAAUUAACACUAAAUUUAAUGGAAUAAUUGUGUUGAUAAAGCUUACUAAAGGUUAUUGAGAUUUAUAGAUAUUAAGAAAGAUCAUACAACUUCAUAUAGCUCCCAAAUAUUUCAAAUGUGAUAUUCAUGUAAUGUCCUUAGGAAUUUCUUUUUCUGGUAAAUGUCAUGUCAUUUUAAUUCAUUACAAAAUAUUUUGAAAUAUGGAAAAAUUUUAAACUUACCUAUAAUUUUCUCUAUAAAUGAACAGUGCUAACAUUUUGGUAGAUGCAUGUUUAUUAUAUUUUAUACAGUUGAACUCAUAAUAUAUUUUCAAUUCAAUAUUCUGCAUUUUCAUAAGUAAUUUUCUGAACUUUCCCCUAUAUUAUUAUAAUUUGACAAUUGGAUUAUUUCCAAUUUAUGCUAUUAGAAAUAAAGUUAAGGUAAACAUUUUUAUGAAUCUUUGUGUGUAUUUCUGUUCAUCUCUUUAGAACAGAGACCCGGAAUAAAUUCUCGAGUCAGAAAGAUUAAGCAUUUUAAAGUUCUUAAUGUAGCUUGCCAACUUUCCUUUUGAAUAUUUGUGAUAAUUUGAUACUUAUAUUUUUAGCAUUGAGUGUUACUGUUUUUCCUAAUCUCUGACUAUUUAAUAAAUACUGAAUUGUAUAGCUUUAUUUUUCUUUUAUUACUAAAGAGACUUAAUUCUUUCAUCUAUUAGCUAAUUCAUCUAUCAGCUUGUAUUAGGGUUCUCUAGAGGAACAGAACUAAUAAGAUAGAUGUAUAUAUGAAGGGGAGCUUAUUAAGGAGUAUUGACUCACAUGAUCACAAGGUGAAGUCCCGCAAUAGGCCGUCUGCAAGUUGAGGAGCAAGGAAGCCAGUUGAAGUCCCAAAACCUCAAAAGUAGGGAAGCUGACAGUGCAGCCUUCAGUCUGUGGCCAAAGGCCUGAAAGCCCCUCAGAAACCACUGGUGUGACUCCAAGAGUCCAAAUGCUGAAGAACCUAAAGUCUGAUAUUUGAGGGCAAGGAGCAUCUAGCACAGGAGAAAGAUGGAGGCUGGAAGACUCAGCAAUUCUGCUCUCUCCAACUUCUUCUGCCUGCUUUAUACUAGCCAGGCUGGCAGCUGAUUAGAUGGUGCCCACCCAGAUUGAGGAUGGGUCUGUCUCUCUGAGUCCACUGACUCAAAUGUUAAUCUCCUUUGGCAACACCCUCGCGGACACACCCAGGAAUAAUACUUUGCAUCCUUCAAUCCAAUCAAGUUGACACUCAGUAUUAACCAUCACAUAGCUCUUUUAAUCUCCUCUUCUGUGAAUUGUCAACUCCUGACCUUCAAACACUUUCCUGUUGAUGAUCUGGAAGUUUUCUUACUAAUUAUAUGUAUCGAUGUAACGUACUAAUGGUGAUAAAAUGAACAGCUUGGGGCAAAAUUUAGGGAUAGAUAAACCUCAAGCUUGUUAUAAUCAGUAUGAUCCCUGCCUUUCUCUCUUCCUUUAGUUCUUUUGGAAAAUGGUCACCAUCAUUUGGUAUAAUCUAUCAUUUCUUAAUAUAUUUCUAAGGCAUCUAGGUGAUAUAUUACAUUCUCUCCCUUUUUCUUAGAGUUUUUUUUAGUGACAGCUUAUGAUUGGGGCAAAUUUAGAGUUGAAGUGUUUCAAUGUGUCUUUACAUGAUAUGUAGGACUUAGAUGCUAUUAAUGUUCUCACCUUUGAUUUAUGGAUCCUGGAUCUUGGACAUAUUGAAUUGUAGAAAAUUUCCCAGAAAGCAACAUAGUGAGAAUAUCCAGAUCAAAAUAGAAUUUUCAAGAGCUGAUGUUACAUGCUGCUCACGAUGGCAAUGAAAGUACAGUUGAACCAAGAAGUCAUGGAUUUAGUUGUAAUGUGGAUGGUAGUUCGUUUCAUCUAAACCAGUGGUUCUCAGACUUUAGCACACAACAGCAUUGCCUAGAGGGGCUGUUAAACACAGGAGCGGGUCCCCACCCUGGAGUUUUUGUUUCUGUAUAGGUCUGGUGUGGAUACCGUGAUGCUGAUGCUUUUGGUCUGGGGACAACACCUUGAGACCACUGAUCUAAGCCAUCUGGGGGCUGAGUGUGAGACAAGAUAUUACCUUUUUCCAUGGUGUAGACUCAUAUCAUGAGAUGUGUAAAUUCUAAAAUCUUGCGAACAGGAGACCAAAAUUACUGUCACAGUGUGGGGGUCCAACAAAGAUAUAAUGUUACCUCCAGGGGGUGCCAUUUCCUUGUGAAUGACUGCCUUAGAAGUUGUGUAUAAGGUACAUGACCAUACAGAGGCCCUGAAGUCUGGUAGUGGAAAUACAUUUUCCUUUGUGAUAUCUGAUGUUACUUUUAAACAUGGAAAGUCCUCCUCCCUUUCCUCUAAGAGUCUCCUACCUGCAAUCUAAAGAUCAAAUUUAUAGUCACCUACGUUUGCUUUUUUUAAUGAAUUCUUUUUAACACCUUCAUUAUAAAGUCAAAUUCUGUUCAUGUAUUCUGUGAGGUGAUGAUUAAAACAGCAUAUUAUUUUCCUAAGUGACAAUUUUCUCCAUACUUUUUGAAUAUACAUUUGUUUUUCAUUCACUGAUGGUGGAAUCUUUCUCGUAUGUUGUGUGUGUGUGUUUGUAUUCUGAGACUAUUUAUAUUGCCUUUGUUGUGCUAGUUCAUUAAUUCUACAAAUGCUUACUAUGUUCCAAGCACUGCAGAGAUAUCAGUAUGAAUGAAACAGUCAUGAAUAAAACACAUGUGGACUCUGCCAGCAUGAAAUUUACCAUCUCAAUAGUCUGUUCCAUUGUUCAUCUGUCUAUUCUAGCUCAAGCAUCACAUUAGUUUUAAUUGUCGUAGCUAAAGAACACAUUUUAAUCUGCUGUAGAGAAAUUAUUCCUUAAUGCCAUUAAAAAAGUUAGUAAUUUUUGUCUAUUUAUUCUUCUUAAUAUACCUUGGAAUAAUUUUUUCAGAAAUUCAAAAAGGGGAAGAAAACUCUUUGUGACUUUCAUUGGAAUUGUCUUGCAGUAUAUUUUGGGAAGAAUUGAUAUCUUUUAUAAAACAGUUUUCCCUCCCAAACCAUUUUUGUAUGCCUUUAUUUAUUGGGAUCUUCUUUCAUAUCUCUGUAUUAUAAAAUAACAUGCAAGUACUAAAAUGUGUUAGUCUGCUGAAUUUUUUGGAAUGCUUUUUAUCAGCAAUAUGAGAAAUUCCAUGAAACUGUAGAACUGGGCCCACAAGGAAGGAAUGAGGCUUGAGGUUAUCAAACAGAGAAGGGAAAGUACAGAGAAAGAAUUACUCUAAAGCAAAAACAGUAGGAAAAUUUUUAUGUUAUCAAGAUAGUCAUGUAAAAUAAUGCAUGGUCCACAUGCAUAAACCACAUCCAAUGCUAGUCUAUGUAUUUUUUCUUGAAAUGUCUGUUUCUCUUGCAAAGUAUAUUGCCAUAUAAGUUUUAAACAGUGAGGACAUCAGUCUCUGAGCAAUAUUCCUGACAUUGUGACAACAACGACUGGCUUUUGCUGUACAUGUUUGCAAACAUUGGUUGAGACUUGUAGGCUGACAGCCUAAAUGGACAAUAUGUCCAUAAUCUGCAUGCCAACUGGCACAUGCUGAUAACAUCUGACAGGCCACUCUUGUCAAAGCUUUUGAACACCUAAUAAAUACAAUUAUACCCCCUUUACCCUUUGAAAAAUCUGAGAUACUGGUUUUUCCCUUUGAGUUACAGAUGGUGAUAUCAUAAGAGCUUUGAGACAGCUGCUCAGCCUCAUUGAUGCAAAUGCUUAUGGCAAACAAUACAUUCUUCAGAUCUGUGGUCGUCUUUCUUUUUUCUUUUCCUGCUUGCUAAUGCCGAGCUGAUGAUGCAGAAUAUGGACCUCAGUUGCAAUUUUAGUAUUAGAGGUCAGAAAACACAUAGAGAUCUGGGUGAACAAAGAAUGUGCAAUAACCACAUUUUACCUGUCCUACAUUGUUUGGGAAUGAGCUCCUAUUGUGUUAAAAUGAACUGCUGGUCAGUGCUGUGGAAACAAUUUAUCCCAAGAACUUAUUAUUGGCUUAGUGAUUGUUUUUUGUUAUCAUGGGUUCUAUAGCCACUGCUAUGAUUGGGUUAGAUGCUCAUUUCCUUUAACUGUGAUGUUUUAAGAAACCCUAGCUUAGGUGAAUAUAAUUGUUACCAUUUAUAAUAGUAGGUUAGAUUCUCAUCUUCUCUGUCUCCGUGUAACAAAGAUAAUAAAUCGAGAUGAUAAAAUUUAAUAAUGUACAAAGUAUUUCAUUGUUAGUGAUGCAUUUUCAAAUGAUGACCUGUGAAAUUGAAAAUAAGAAGGGAGAAACUUUUUUUCCCCUCUCCUAUUAAGGAUCACUGACCGGCUUGGAAAAAAAAAAUCCCAAGUCAUGUAAAAGGAAAAUAAUUUGUUUGCAUUUAUAUUUUUAUUAAGAGAGAGAAAUAUAAACAACUAAAGAUAUUCUUUUAAAGUUAAAAUUUGGGGUUUUAAAGUUUCAUUGGCUAACUACGUUAAAUUAAGAGAAAUAUGUAAUUUAAUGUGAGAGUAACAGGAGACUGCAGGAUUGGGGGAGGGAGAUGAAUGGUAUGGGGGAGGGCGAGACUGGCAGACAGAGACUGCAGGGAAACUAGAGGAGAGAGGAGAAGGUGGUGGGGAAAAAAAGGGAAAUGAAAGAAAGGAAAGAGAAAUUAAAUGUUUAAUAAUAGAGCCAAAGGACAAAGAAAAGAGCAUGUAGGAGGAUGGCGUGAGCUCAGGAGUUUGAGCUUGAGCUCAGGAGUAUGUCAGCCUGGGCAACAUAGCAAGACUUCAUCUCUACUAAAAGAAAAAAAAAAAAUCUGGGUGCAAUGGUGAGCACUUACAGUUCCAGCUACUUGGGAGUCUGAGGUGGGAGGAUGGCUUGAUUCUUGGAGGUUGAGUCUGCAGUGAGAUGAGAUUGUGCCACUGCACUCCAGCCUGGGUGACAAAGUGAGACCCUGUCUCAAAAAUGAAAACAAAAACAAAAAACAAUAAUUGAUAGAAGGAAGGUGAUAAGGGCACAUGAUGAGACAGUAAGAGGGAGAAGGAAGCAACUGCAACUGGAACUAAAAAGAGAAAUGCUUAGAGGGCUUUCCAAGCUCUGAGAUGACUGUGUGUCUUGGCUUGGGUUCCUAUCUUGUUUCCCUGGAUGUCCGAAUCAGUUACUACCAGAUCCUCUGACAGCCCAGCCUGGGAGUCUCUUCUUUCUAUAGCUGGUGUCCCAGAUUCCCAGUUGCUUAUUACUAUAACCUUGGUCUUUAUGGUCAAUGCUGACCCCACCUGGACUCGGCAGCCACCAGUCUUGCCUCUUGCCUAGCCCUGAUUUUGUGUUUCAUUUUCUGUCAUUGGGUCUAUCUGGUUUUUGUUUUGUUUUGUUUUCCUAUGCCAAGCAUCUGUCUUUGGUAAUCUCCCUACUACUUUUUUCUUUCUAAAUGCAAGGUAUUCCCUUUCUCCUAUAAGCGUCUCUUCUGAGCCUGGGAACCUUUGACUGCAGCCCAAGCCCCAUGUCCUAUAUCCAGUGCUCUCAUGAUGGGAACCAUCAGCCUGGAUGGCCGAAUCCCCCCAUUCCUGAUGGUCUGCUCACAUUGUGAUGCACCCUGCUGAACCUGUCAUGAAGACUGCCUGAAACUCUACAUUAUGGAUAUUUUGGCUGACUUCCUUGUUUGGAAAGUCUUAUUUGGUUACCAGAUAACUGGAUCAUGUCAAGGUCCAAAAAUAUGUCAAUUUUUCCUUUGAAAUGUUAUAAUAUAUUAUUUUCUGCCUUGAGAUUUUUUUUUUCAAAUGUCAAGGGGGCAGGGACAAUGUUUUAAAUAAACUUUCCAUUGAGAUUCUGGAAAUGAUUAUGAGGAAACAACUGAGGUUUUAGAAAUGUAACUGGAAAAUGUAAAAAUGCCAUCAACUUCCUAGUUAUUCCCAAAAGUCUCUUUGACAUUGAAAUGAUGCCAAAAAUAUAUCAUGUUUGUUCUUUGAGAAAUUAGAGCUCUCUCAUUCCAUAAUGCAAAAAAGUUGUACUUGCAAAUAAUAUCCCAAGCUGCUUGCUAGAGAUUGGAUGAAAUUAAAUAGCUGCUGAUCUGAAGUCAUUUCAUGUCUGACUUGUGAGUACAAGUGUUGGGCACAAUUGAAGUUUUCUUUCUAAUUAAAAAUUAGGCUUUUUUUCUUUCAUAAUCAACUUACUGUCUGUAGUGGUUCACAUAAUUGCUGGUAGCAGCACUUUCCAUUGAUCCUAAUUUGUGGAAGGUUGUAAGAUGAGAGAACUUAGAUUUUCACCAUAAUUCACCUUUAAAUAAAAAAGAGGUAAUAUAAAACCUUGUUUGGUUUGUUUCUGAAACUUUUGUUCCUUUGCUCAUCCUGUCACUCAUGAGCAUGUUCUGAUUGACUUUGUGGGAAGAGGACACAGCAUUAGCAUUUCACCUGGUCUGUUAGGAACAAACAAAAAAACCAACCAAUCAACAAUGUCUUAAGAAUACUUGACAAAACUUAAAUCUAUGGCUGAAUCUACAUAAUUAUGUUAGAAUGACCUGGUAGGGGAAAAUGUGCUGGGCCUAAAGUGUUGUUUCACAGCUCAAGCUGCUGCAUGAACAGCAUGGGCAGGUCCCCUGAAUGACAUGCUGGGAGCUAUGUAUGGCUCCGGGUCCACUGAGCUGGUCUCAUCUUCCCCUUAUGAGAGCGAUGGUAUGACAGGUGCAGUGUGUGCACUUGUAUGGGAUGACGGGUUGGGGUGACUGCAGGUGAAGGAGGCAGGAAGAAGCAGAAAGCCUUGGUCUUAUGCAUACUGCCCCCAAGGUGUGGAAGCCACAGGUGGUCAUUAUUAUGAAAUCUGGGAAGUGUAAUCACUGGGCAGAUCAUAAUAACAGGUAACCCAGGUGGCAGGUGAGGGUUACUAUCAGGUGGGCACAGUGGCUUUGGGAGACAAGACCGUUAACCCCUAGAUUGGACUUAGAGGAGAUCCUAGGGGUGGAUUUGUAUGGAGUAAUUUUCCUAGACUAAAUUACUAUUUAGUUAUAACCAUGGAUGCUAUUAUGGGUUGAAUUUUGUACCCCCCAAAAUACAUAAAAGUUGCAAACCCCAGUACCUGUGAAUGUGACUUUAUCUGGAAAUAAGGUCCUUGAAGAUGAAAUUAGUUAAGGUGAGGCUAUUAGGAUAGGACCUAAUCCAAUAUGACUGAAAAAAGGGGAAAAUUUGUCCAUAGAGUUGGAAGCACACACAGGGAAAACAGCACGUGAGGAUAAAAGCAGAGACUGGGGUGAUGCAUCUGCAAGCCCCAAAGAAUAUAAAAGAUUGCUAGCAAAUUACCAGAAGCCAGGAGAGAGCCCUGGAACAGAUUUCCCCUCAAAGUCCUUAAAAGGAAGCAAUCCUGCCGACAUCUUGAUCUCGGACUUCCUUCAGAACUGUGAGGCAGUAAACUUCAGUUAUUGUGAGCCAUUCAAUUUCUGGUACAGUUAUGGCACCCAUAAAGAAUGAAUACAGGUGCUAGAGGAUUGGAGGUUUGGUUAACAGAAAAUAUUAGUACUAGAAGAAACCCUAGAAAUUGUAUAAUUGACAUAGGAAACACUACUGUACUGUAUACUUAAAAUUUCCUAAGAGAUAGAUCCUAAAUGUUCUCACCACAAAAAAUCAAGAGCAGCAGCAAAACUAUGUGAUGACUAUGUUAAUUAUCUUGAUUGUGAUGAUAACUUCAUGGUGUAUAUGUAUACUAAAUCAUCAGGUUGUACAUCUUAAAUACAGUCAUGUACCAUGUAAUGUUUCAGAUACGCGAGGGAUCAGAUAUGUGAGAGUCGCCCCAUAAGAUUACAAUACCAUAUGUUCACCUUACCUUUUCUAUGUUCAGAUAUGUUUAGAUAUACAAAUACUUACCAUUCUGUUACAAUUGCCGAUAACAUUCAGUACAGUGACAUGCUGUACAGGCUUGUAGCCUAGGAGCAAAAGGUUAGGUGUGUAGUAAGCUAUACCAUCUAGGUUUAUGUAAGUACACUCUACAAUGUUUGUAAAAUGAUGAAAUAGCCUAAUAUUGCAUUUCUCAGAAUGUAUCUCUGUCAUUAAGAGAUGCAUGACUUAUAUAUACAAUUUUUUAAAAAAUUGUGUAGUUGAGACCUCUUAUAUUACCAAUGAAUUACUGAGGCCUAGAAAGGUCAAAUGAAUUAAUUGCUUGAGGUCACCUAGCUAGCAUGUGGCAAGUCUGAGACUAAAGCCUCUGUCUUUUGACUCUUGGUCUGUGCUUUUCCUGUACUUUUUUGCUCCUGUGCACAAUUACCAUGUAGCAUGCGCAUAGAAACACAGAUUAGAAAUACACAGAAGAUAAUCACAUAACUUAGAAAUGAGUUUUGAAAAGGUGUAGCCGGACUCCUUAUCUAAAAUUAAUCUAACUGAAAUUGUAUUUUAGAUUAACUUUGCUACUUGAAAAAUGCUAAGUGGCUGCCUGAGAGCAAUGAAAUUUCUUCCUCUAAUGUGCUCCUCAGGGCAGGUAGCCCUUAUCAUUGUUUUCCAAACCACUAGCCAUUAACAUUUGUGGGGUGCCUGUGGAGUAUCUGGCUCUCCUAGUGUCUCAGCUCUCUGUACAGUCAGAGGGGUGGCAGCUUUCUGCCCUUGGUCACAAGACAAUGCCCCAUUGUGCUUGCUUAUCCAGAAGAUCAAUCAGGAAGAGAAGCACGCCAUGGGCUGAACUGCAGUUUCUGUUACCUGACUUAGUUUAGAUGUAUUUCUCCUCUCCCUCAAAUCCCUCCCACUAAGUCCAAGGAUGUUUGCAAAUGUCCUAAGGAAUAUUCUAGUAGCUAGGAUCUGGCAUUUUCACAGCCACAGCUCAAGAUAAAGUCCAACUGCAAAAAAAAAAAAAAAAAAAAAAAAGUAAGAGUUGAAAAUGAAAAUGACUUCAAAGCAAUGAAAUAUAAAGUAAUUGCAAGUUUGCAAAUUAACUAUGUUGGCAUAUUCUUCACUUCCUCAAGGAAAUAUGCUCUAUCCCGUUUUUAAAAAUCAUAAAUAUAUUUUUUAACUUUUUAUUGGAGUUUGACACACAUUCAGAAAAGUAUAAAAAUCAUAAUAAUCAACCGGAUAAUUUUUCACAAAGUAAAAACCAUGAAGAAGCAACAGAUUAAGAAGCAUAUCAUCAUUUCCCAGGGAUAACCACCAUUCUGAUUUUUAACACUAUGGUGUUAAAAAUCCAUUUAUUUGGUCUGUUUUGGAAACUUAUACAAGUGGAAUCAUACAGUAUGUACUAUUUUGCUUCUGUUUUUCUCAACAUUGUGUCAUAUAUUUGUGAUUUCUUCAUUCUCAUUGCUAAAUAGUAUGCCAUUGUAUGAAUAUAUCACAAUUCACUACAUUUCAGUUUUUUUUUGCUAUUACAAUCAGUGCUACUAUCAACAUUUUUGUACAUAUCCUUUGGUGGACAAAUGUAUGCAUUUCUGUUGAGUGCUUCUGAAGAGUGGAAAGCUGGGUCAUUGGGGAUGCAUGUGUUCAACUCUGGUAGCUACAACAAAACAGUUUUCCAAAGUGAUUAUACAAAUUUACACUCCAACUGGCAGUGUAAUAAGCUCUUCAAUCUUUCAGGUUUUUGCCAACAAUUGGGAUUUUUCAGUUAGUUUCUUUUUAACCACUCUGGUGUGUGUGUAGUGGUAUCAUAUUAAUGGUUUUGAUAUGCUAAUUAUAAUGAUGAUUAAUAAAAUUGAGCAUCUUCUCAUGUAUGUAUUGAUUCUGUAGAUCCUCAACAUGAAGGGCAUGCUAAGGUGUUUUGCCUAUUUUUCUGUAGGGAUUUUACCAUUAUAAUAUUAAUUUGUAGUUUUAAAAUAUAUGAAUAUAUAUUUUGUGGCUUGUUUUUUCACUUGGUUAAUCACAUAUUUUGAUGAACAAAUAUUUUUAAUUUAAAUAUAGUCCAAUUUAUCCAUCCCACCUGAGUCUGUGCUAAUGAGAUGACUCAAGGUAGAAAGACCAAGUUGACAUGAGAGUUGGAACUUUCAGGCCCUUCCACCACCCUCUGGGAAGAGUGGAGGGGAGGGAGCUGGAGAUUGGGCUCAGUAAAAACUCUUGACAGUGAGGCUCAGAGAGCUUCCAGGUGGGUGAACACACCAAGGUGCUCGGAAGGUGGUGCACCCAAGAGGGUAAGGAGGCUCUCUCUGUGUGACUCCCUCGCUCUGUAUCUUGCCAUGUGCAUUGCUUCCAUUUGGUUCUUCCUGCAUUGUAUCCUUUAUAAUAAACCAGUAAAUGUAAGUUUAAAAGUGUAAAUAAGUAAGUUCUGUGAGCAGCUCUAGCAAAGUAUUAAACCCGAGGAGGGGUGGUGGAAACACUUGCUUUACAGCUGAUUCAUCAGAAGUACAGGUGGCUCAGGGCUUGAAACUGGUGUCGGAAGCGGGAACAGUCUUGUCCUGUCGAGCUCCUUACUUUAUGGAGUCUGUACUAACUCUGGGUAGAUAGUGUCAGAAUUGGAUUGAAGUUUUGGACACCCAGCUAGUAUCUAGAGAAUCAGAGAAUAGGUUGUUGGUGUCAGAGAAAACACCCCAGAGAACCAAAUUGUCAUAAUUUUCUCUUGUCUUUUUAAUAUUUGUAAGAUCUGAGAGGGUGCUUCUUUUGUAUAUUUCUGUUAUCAGCAAUUUAUGUUCACUCUAUUUUUUUCUGAUCCAUCUUCGUAAAAGUUUAUCCAUUUUAUUAAUACUUUGAUAAAAAACUUUCAUGUUACUGAUUUUCUGUAUUGAAUAACUGGAUUUUAUUCCAUUAAUUUUUAUUCCUAAUUUAUUGUUUUCUUCCUACUGCCUUACUUUUUAUUAUGGGGGAGAGUUAAUUUGUUGAAUUUUUAUCUAAAUUCCUAAAUUGAAUUCUUACAUCAUUAAUUUUGAACCUUUCUUCUGUUUUAAUAUGUUAAUCAAAUGUUAUAAUUUUUUUUCUAAGUAUGACUUCAACUGCCCUCCACAAAUUUUAUUAUAUCUGAUAUUUACUAUCAGGUUCAAAAAUUAUUUGUUUUUUCAUUGCAACUUAUUCUUGAUCCAUGGAACAAUUUAAGAUUAUGUUGCCUCAUUGCCAGACACAUGGGGAUGAUUUCAUCAGAGAAUAUUCUCUGGAUAGUUUUGGUUCUUCAAAAAUUUGCUUUAUAGCCCAGCAUGUUGCUAAUUUUGGUAAAUGUUACAUGUGCGUGUGAAAAGCAUGCAUAUUCUCCAGUUGAUGUGCAUAGUAGUCUGUAUAUACCAAGUGUGUCAAGUAUGUUCAUCAUGCUGUUGUCAUAGCCAUUAUCUUACUAUAAUGUUUCUGUUGAAGUCAUCAAAUAUUUUUAUGUUUUUAUUUCAAUUUCUAUUACCUUGUCUGUCAUAUCUUAUUUUAUUGUUAUUUAAUGCUUACCCUGACUUACCGUAGUCUAAUAAAAUUACUUUCAUCAAUUCUCUGAUCAUGCUGAAACCUUACAAUAGUUUAGAAACCUUAUAAUAGUUUAGAAACCUUACAAUAGUUUAACCCCAUUCAUCUACAUUCUGCCUCUCACAUUAUUGCCAUCAUAUAUUUUUAUUACGUUAUGAACUCUGUAGCACGUUACUAUUAUUGUUUUGUAUAGCCAACUUUAAUUUAUAUUUAUCCACAUAUUUACAACUUUCUGCUGAGACAGCCAAAUGCCUGGGCAGAUAAAAAUGGGUCCCCAGAGAAUCUCCGACCCAACCCACAAGUGUUUACAUCAGAUGCUUUUGUGCAGAUGAGGAAACCUGCCCAGGGUUUUGUCAGGGCAUGCCCACAGUGGAUGGGAGCUGGACAUGCGUACUGAGGGAAGUGGAUGGAGCUAUGGGGAAUUCCUGCCUUAAGCAGGGGAGGAGGCUGUUCUCUUCAGCAGGGGUAGUAACCUGGGAAUCAGUCUGUGAGGAGGCGGGCCUGUUAGCAGGACUCCGUCUCACUUUCCUGAGAGAUUUUUUUUUUUUCCUUUUUGCCCAAUACAUUCCUCUCUAAUCACCCUUCAAUGUGUCUGCGCACCUAAUCCUUUCUGGUCAUAUGACAAGAACCUGGUUUUUUCUACAACACUGCCACCCUUUAUUCCUUCUUGCAUUUUGUGUUUCUGUUUAGGAAUAUUCUCCUUUAGCCUAAGGAAUUUCCUUUAGUAAUUAUUUUAGGAAAGUCUGAUGGUGGUGAAUUUUCUUAAUUUGUAUUUGUCUGCAGCAUAUUCAUUUUACCUUUGUUUCUGAAGGUUAUUUUCAAUUGCUAUAUUAUUCUAGUUUGGCACUUUGUUUUUGGCACCAUAAAUAUAUACUUUUAUUGUCUUUUAACUGCCAUUGUUUCUGUCAAUAAACCAGCCCAAUCUUGUUUUCUUUCUUCGAAGCUGCCUGUUUUCUUUGGCUAUCUUUAAGAUUUUUCUAUCUUUGGUGUUUAACAGUUUGCAAUUAUGUGACUAAGUGUAGAUUUAAGGUUUUUUUUUUCUUCUUAGUGUUUAUGAAACUUCUUGAAUGUAUGGGUUGAGAGCCUCCAUCCGAUUUUGAAGAUUAUAGGCAAACAUCUCUUCAAUAUUGCUUCCACCUCAUUCUUUGUGUUAUCAAUUGAGGACACUGAUCAUGUGUAUUUUAGAAUUUUUAAAUAUCUCCCAUACAUAACUUAUGUUGUUUUAUACAUUUUAAAAUGUUUUUAUCCUUUAAUUUGCAUAUUUUCUAUCUUCCUGUUCAGUAAUAUCAUUUGUUCAGGGGAGCCCAAUCUAAUGAUCUGUUGAAUUGUCAAUUUUAGAUAAAAUUUCUAUUUGAUUUUUAAAAUAUUGUCUACUUUUUCUCUAAAAUUCUCUUAUCUUUUUUUGUACAUUAAUUAUAGCUGUUUUAAAGUGUGUGUUUGAUAAAUCUAAUGCCUGCAUCACUUGUUGGUUUGUUUCUGUAUCCUAUUUUAUAUUCUUAAUAAUGCUUCUUGGUAUGCAUUGUAAUUUUUUUGCCUUUUAUUUUUGUUUUUUAGUAACUAAUAUUAGCAACAAUAAUGACUAAUGGCCUGAAGACUGAAGGUAUUAUUUUAUUUUAUUAAUUUUUAUUUUUAAUUCUUACGAGUACAUAAUGGUUGUCUAUAUUUACGGGGUACAUGCGAUGCUUUGAUACAGGCAUACAAUGUAUAAUAAUCAAAUCAGGGUAAUUGGGGUAUCCAUUGCCUCAAGCCUUUAUCAUUUCUUUGUGUUAGGAACAUUCCAUACUUUUUAAUUUAAUGCUAAGGUACAUUAUGCACUUAGAGUUUCAACAUCAAUGGCAGUGGGCUCAUCCAUAUUUCACAUACUCUUCUUAAUUGUUUCACCCUUUUUUACAGACUUCCUGUGAUGUCUGAUUAAACUCUUGUAGUUUUAUACCAUAAUAAGUUUAUAAACAAUACAGGAGCAGAAUAAAUAUCAGCACCAUUAUUGUUGUUUUGGGGUACAUGGUACUAAUUCAUAGAUCCUCCUGCUAUUUGAAUGAUAGGGUAAUUAACAUCUUAUUUUUUUUUUAUCACGUUAGCUGUAUACUUGUAGUCAAUUUAUGUAGUGAGUAGAUUGAAUUGGAAUGCCAAUGGUUCUAAAUUCCCUGGAGAAAAUCUUGAGAAGUCUGGUGCCCACCUUUAGCAGUUGGCCUGUUCCAAUGACAUGAAACCUUGACUGCUAAGGUGCCAUAAAGCAGAGCUGUUUCUGCCUUGGUGAAUGGAGUGAGGCAUAGGAAACACCUUCAGAGUGGCUCCCAUCAAUAAUCAUUGGAGAAUUUCAUAAUUUUGAUUGUCAAGGUCAAUAUGUGGUUGUUUCCAUAAUUUUAGUCAAGGCCUUUAACAAAAAAUAGCAUGUGAACUAGUAUGUUUAUUAAUGACAUUUCAUAAUUUACUUUAGCAUUCAUUUUUCAUUGAUGGGCAGGGAUAAGCCCUGCCUUAGAUUCUGCAAGUUUCUGAGGCAUCUUGCCUCAGAAAUAGACCUAGGGUCUCUAUUUUAAGCAUAUUACAUAUGUUAACUUCUUUUAACUUCAUAACACGGCAUAAGGUAUGUACUAUUUUUAUUUCUAGCCUACAGGAAAUAGAAGCCUGUACUAGUUUUCUGUUGCUGCUUAAUAGAUUACCACAAACUUACUGACUUAAAACAUCAUACAUAUUUUCUAUCUCACAUUUACAUGGUCAGGAGUCUGAGCAUGCCCUACCUACAUGGUUUUUGCAAGGUUUCACAAAGCUGUCUAGAAGUGAAGAUUAGGAAUGUUUCCAGCACAAAGACAUGAUGAAUAUUUGAGGUGAAGGAUAUCCUAAUUACCACGAUUUGAUCAUUAUGUAUUGUGUGCAUGUGUUCAAAUAUCACAUGCACCCUAUAAAUAUGUACAAUUAAUACGUAUCAGUCAAAAAUAAAAGAUGUUGGAUGGGGCUGAAAUUCCAUCUUAGGCUUGUAGUCCUCUUCCAAGUUCACAUGGCUGUUGGCAGAAUUUAUUCUCUUGAAUCUGUAGAACUCAUGGGGGGCUUGCUUCUUUUUUGAGGCCAGAAGGAGAUUCUCUUAUUUUGAUUAAAGUCAACUGAUUAGAACUUUAAUGAUAUCUGAAUAAUCCCUUGACUUUUACCAUAUUGUAUUGGUUAGAAGCAAAUUCGCAGGUUCUAUUGGGCAGAAGCAAGCUUUCAAGGGGAGGUAAACAUACAAGGGCAUGAGUCAUUGGCUGUCAAUUUAGGGUAUGUCUUUUACAAAGCCCCCCAAAAUUAAUUGACCUGCUUCUAGUCAGUAUUGGUAGAGGGUAAGAUUUGACUCCAAGCUGCUUGGCCCUAGAGCAUAAGCACUUUGUUGCUUACUUUCUCAGGGUUAUCCAUUCUCAUACACUGCAGCCUGAGAAAGGAUUGAUAGGAAUUUGUUUGCAGACAUUCAAGAUCAUGUAUUUUGUGUAUUUGUGUCCUCUAUUCAUUUGGUUGUUAUGAACUCUCUAUAUAAACUACCCUUCUACUUUCUGUGACAAGUGACAUCCUUUUUCUUGUGCAAUUAAAAGUGCUAAAUUUAUUUCAAUCCAAAACACAUCCUUUGCAAAUCCCUACAUUUGUAAUAUUGAACAAAGUGAGCAGCUAUGCCAUUUAAGUAACAAUUCCUUCCAACGCUGCUCAUUAUAUGUGUGAAAUUUAAAUCUUUGAUCAAUGAGUGAUGACGAUGAGUGUGCUGUUGAUAAUGCUCUGAGAGCAUCUACUUUUAGGUGAAGGAAAGAAUGCAAGGAUGUGGAACCCAUUUAGUCACACAUAUGUUUAAGCCCUAGAAACUGUUGGUUAUGUGGUUCAUUUGCGAUCACCAUCCUCUAUUCUGCUUGUUUUAAACACGGGAUGAAAAUCUUUCAACACAAGAAUUUUGUGAAGUCACAGACUGACCCUUGAAAAAUACCAGUAAUCAGCCAUUUAAAAAUACAUUUAAAUCAUUUUGUUUGAGUUCAAGGUGCAGGAAUCUUCAGUUUUGCGACUAAAGUUAGCACUUGAGAAUGGAAUUGUAUUGCCCCACCCACACGCACACACUCAAAUUUCCACAUAUUCCUUUCUUUUUGCCAAGAGAUGAGAAGAUAUUGCCCUGGAUAUUCAAGGAAACAGUGGGGGCAAAUGCAACAGCAACAGUCCAUGAUUGGUACAAGAAACUUCAGAUUAACCCCUUGGAAACAACCAGAAGACUUAACUCAGCAUCUCAGAAAGAUCAAAAUCAUUGUCAUAGAGCCAAAGGGCUCCCAGGCAUAACACAUUUUUGUUUUUGUUGUUAUUCCUCUCAUCUUGAGUUUCUGAGACCUAUUUCCUCCUCAGAUCCCGGCUAAUCUGUUAGCCUUGUCAGCUCUUGCCCUGUGGAUCAGACUCCUCCCAUUUCUCUGCCUUGUUGAUUAACAUCCUGCUUUCUGAUCCCAGCUCAUCUCUAUGGCCUUUGCCUCAUAUUCUUUCAUACUAUUAUUUCCAUUUUAACCAUUAUAUUCUAAUUCUGUAGUGUGAUUGGGAAAACCAUUGGCAAGAAAGAUACAAAAAUAGAGCCCUAGGGUUAAGGUUAUGUCCUUAUGAUUUUCCAUAUUCAUAUAGUACUUAGCACUUCAUACAUGUUAACUCAUGAGACUUCAAAAUAUCCUUACGAGGGAUUCUGAUUCUUAGAUACAGUUUGCAAAUUAAGGAAGAUAAAUAUAUAUAGAAAAAAACACAAUAGUAACAAACUUGACAGGAGAGGAUUAACUUCUGGGAGCACAAAGUGGAGUUCUUGGCCUGAGCCCACAGCUCCAGGAAACUUCAAUGAACUGAAAAUGGCCUGUCUGGGUAACGAGGCUCUGUACAUCUCUCUUCACCCUAAAGUUGAGUCAGUGAGGCAUUAUGAUGUUUUUAAUUUCUCAAGUGAUAUUAAAAUACAGACCCACAGACCCCAUCUGUUCUCUUGGAAGCAGAGAGAUUGGCAAAUGAUAACACUACAUGCCUUUAGGGAUAUACGCUGCCUGAUAAUCACCAUGUGGUUUCAACUAGUUCACGCUCAGAUGAACCUGAUAUGAAUUUAGAAAGGGCAAACACUCCUAAUGAGAUGGUAUAUUCUUGACUUACUAUUUUAAACAGCACCUUCUUCCUACUACCUGCAAACACCACAUUUGUAUCCCUUUCUAAGGCGGGACAUCUUGGAGUCAUCUUUGUUUCCUCUUUCCAUUUAUCUUCUAUAUAUCCAGAUGGAGAAUCUUAUGGUUUCUUUGUGAUAUGCCUUUUGCUUUCUGAUCUUACUGCCAUCACUUGAGUUCAAACCUUCAGUAUCUCAUCUGGAGCGCUGCUCUGUCGGCCUAGGAAAUGGCUCUGACUCUGGUUCUCUCCACUUGGAUAAUCUCAUGUUGCCUGGGGAAUGUUUCUAAAAUGGCCAAUAGGAGAAUCCCUGUCUGUAGAGUACAAUUGCUGUGUUUGCCUUCCCAGUAGCACUUUCCCAUUAUUCUUUUAAUAACACCCCACAUUUUAAGAAGCGACUUAUUACAGCACUGUUUUUUCCUUCCAUCGUUAUCAAAUAAAUGUUCCUGUGAUCCAAACCAGCUCAACCAUUGUCAAGACACAUGACUCAGGCAGUCUAAUUGGAAUGUGCCCUGGGAUUACUGGGAUUGCUGUAUACAUUGGUAUACAGCAGUAGUUUCCAGACUUUUUUCUUUCAGAAACUCUUUUUACUCUUAAAAGUUAUUGAGGACUCCCAAGAGCUUUUGUUAAUGUGGCUUCUAUCUGUACAUUUCCAUAUUAUAAAUUAAAAAUGAUAAAUACAUUUAUUAUUUCAUUUAAAUACAAAAUAGUAAACCCUUUACAUGUUAACGUAAAUAAAAUACUUUUAAGCAUAUAACUUUUCUAAAAUGAAAAUAUUUUGUGAGAAAAAUGGCAUAGUUUUAUAUUUUUGUAAAUCUCUUUAAUAAUUACCCUAAUAAACAAAUCUACUGCACAUGCAGUUCAUAAAAUAUGUUGCUACGGAUGAAGUGUAUGAAGAAAAUCUGGCCUCACAGAUGUGUAGUUGGAAAAGGGAGAAUCAUUUUAAUAGUCUUUAUAGAUAUUAUGGAUAUUAUUCUUUGAGACUAUACUAAAACUUGACAAGUGGCAGUUUCCUAAAGGUUAGUUGCAAUGUGAAAUCUGAAACCAUGUCGGUGAGCUUUUUGUACGCAGCUAUAAUAAAAUCUGUUGGCAGUUUGUACAGAUCUUUUACAUGUUCAUGAUUUCAUUUGGAAAUGCACUGAUUAUUUGGAAAGUAUACGUUCAUCAAGAUAUGCAUAUCUGCUAAAUGAUGACAUGUGUUCAUUUUAUGAUGUCUUAAACCACAUUUAGUAACAUCACCAGUGACCUCAUCUGAAAAUUGGGAUACCAUCAAGCUUAUAAUGCAACAUACAUGUUGAUAUGGUUUGGCUCUGUGUCCCCACCCAAAUCUCACUUUGAAUUGUAAUAAUCCCCAAAUGUCAAUGUGUCAAGGGUAGGACCAGGUGGAGGUAAUUGGACCAUGGGGGUGAUUUCCCCUAUGCUGUUCUCAUGAUAAUGAGUGAGUCUCAUGAGAUCUGAUGGUUUUAUAAGCAUCUGGCAUUUUCCCCUGCUUGCACUUAUUCUCCUGCUGCCCUGUGAAGAGGUGCCUUCUCUCAUGAUUGUAAGUUUCCUGAGGCCUCCUCAGCCAUGCGAAACUAUAAGUCAAUUAAACCCCUUUUCUUUAUAAAUUACCCAGUCUCUAGCAGUUCUUUAUAGCAGCGUGAGAAUGGACUAAUACAGUAAAUUGGUACUGAGAGUGGGGUGCUGCUAUAAUGAUACUCAAAAAUGUUGAAGCGACUCUGGAACUGGGCAACAGGCAGAAAUUGGAACAGUUUAGAAGGCUCAGAAGAAGACAGGAAAAUGUAGGAAAGUUCAGAACUUCCUAGCUUGGAGGACUCAGAAGACAGGAAGAUGUGAGAAAGUUUGGAACUUCCUAGAGACUUGUUGAAUGGCUUUGGUCAAAAUGCUGAUAGUGAUAUGGACAAUGAAGUCCAGGCUGAGGUGGUCUCAAAAGGUGAUGAGGAACCUCUUGGGAACUGGAGCAUAGGUGACUCGUGCUAUGCUUUAGCAAAGACACUGGUGGCAUUUUGGCCCUGUCCUAGAGAUCUGUGGAACUUUGAACUUGAGAAGGAUGAUUUAGGGUAUCUAGCAGAAGAAAUUUCUAAGUGGCAAAGCAUUCAAGAGGAAGCAGAGCAUAAAUGUUUGGAAAAUGUGCAGCCUGGCGAUGUGAUAGAAAAGAAAACCCCAUUUUCUUGGGAGAAAUUCAAGUUUGCUGCAGAAAUUCGCAUAAGUAAUGAGGAGUGAAAUGUUAAUCACCAAGACAAUGGGGAAAAUGUCUCCAGGGCAUGUUAGAGACCUUCAUGGCAGCCCCUUCCAUCACAGACCGAGACCUAAGAGGUAAAAAUGGUUUUGUGGGCUGAGCCCAGGGACCCCCUGCUCCAUGCAGCCUUGGGACAUGGUGCCCUGUGUCCCAGCUGCUUCAGCUCUAGCUGUGGCUAAAGGGGCCAAGGUACAGCUCAGGCCAUUGCUUCAGAGGGUUCAAGCUUUAAGCCUUGGUGGCUUACCUGUGGUGUUAGGCCUGUGGGUGCACAGAAGUCAAGAAUUGAGGCUGGAGAACCUCUGCCUAGAUUUCGGAGAAUGUAUGGAAACGCUUGGAUGUUCAGGCACAAGUUUGCUUCAUGGGUGGAAACUUCAUGGAGAACCUCCACUAGGGCAGUGUGGAAAGUAAAUGUGCGGUUGGAUUCCCCCAAAGUCCCCACUAGGGCACUGCCUCGUGGAGCUGUGAGAAGAGGGCCACUGCCCUCCAGACCCCAGAAUUAUCAAUCCACCAACAGCUUGCCCUGCAUGCCUGGAAAAGCCUCAGACACUCAAUGCCAGUCUGUGAAUUCAGCCAGGAGAGGGGCUGUACCCUGCAAAGCCACAAGGGUGGAGCUGCCCAAGGCCAUGGGAGCCUACCUCUUGCAUCAGCAUGACCUGGACGUGAGACAUGGAGUUAAAGGAAAUCAUUUUGAAACUUUAAGGUUUAAUGACUACCCUAUUGGAUUUUGGACUUGCAUGGGGUCUGUAGCCCCUUUGUUCUGGUCAAUUUCUCCCAUUUGGAAUGGGUGUAUUUACUCAGUGCCUGUACCCCCAUUGCAUCUAGGAAGUAAUUAACUUGCUUGUGAUUUUGCAGGCUCAUAGGCAGAAGCAACUUGUGUUGUCUCAGAUAAGACUUUGGACUUGGACUUUUGGGUUAAUGCUGGAGUGAGUUAAGACUUUGGGGGACUGUUGGAAGGACAUGAUUGUGUUUUGAAAUGUGAGUACAUGAGAUUUGGGAGGGUCAGGGGUGGAAUGAUAUGGUUCAUCUCUGUGUCCCCAUCCAAAUCUCACCUUUCCCCACGUGUCAAGUGUGGGAACAGGUAGAGGUAAUUGGAGCAUGGGGGCAGUUUCCCCCAUGCUGCCCUCAUGAUAAUGAGUGAAUCUCACAAGAUCUGAUGGUUUUAUAAGUGCCUGGCAUUUUCCCCCACUUGCACUCAUUCUCUCUCCUGUCACCCUGUGAAGAAGUGCCUUUUGCCAUAAUUGUAAGUUUCCUGAGGCCUUCUCAGUGAUGCGGAACUGUGAGUCAAUUAAACCUCUUUUCUUUAUAAAUUACCCAGUCUCAGGCAGUUCUUUAUAGCAGCCUAAGAACAGACUAAUACACGUUUUCCAAAAUCAGCAAUUAGAAAGCUAAAAAUUUAUCAUUUACGUUAAGCACCGUACUCAAUUCUGAAUAACAAUAGUUUAUGUAUUGGUUAUUCUUUCAAAUUAAAAUAGUAUUCCAUGCAAAUGUGGCUCACAACUCAAACAUUUGGCUGAGUGCUUUUCCUCAUGACAUGAUUGUACUGUGGUGUGCAGUAGAAGUCCUUUAGGUGCACGUGAUGAUUAAUUUUAUGUGUCAACUUGAUUAGGCCGCAGAGUGCCCAAAUAUUUGGUCAAAUAUUAUUCUGGGUUUUUCUGUGAGGGUGUUUCUGGAUAAAAUUAACAUUUGAAUAGGUAGACUGAAUAAAGCAGAUUGUCUUCCCUAAUGGGGUUGAGCCUCAUCCAAUAAAUUGAAGACUUGAAUAGAACAAAAAGACUGACCUUUCCAGGUAAGAGAGAAUUUCUCUUACCUGACAGCCUUCAAAUUGAGACAUAAGCUUUUUUCCUGCCUUUAAACUCAAGCUAAAAUAUUGGCUUAUCCUGGGUCUCAAGCCUGCUGGCCUUGGGAUUGAAACUAAACCAGGAGCUUUCCUGGGUCUCCAGCUUCUGACUGCAGAUCGUGGGACUUGCCUGUCUCUCUCUGCUUUCUCUCUCUCUUUCUCCCUCUCUCUCUCUCUCGCUCUACACACACACACACACACACACACACACACACACCCCGUUAUGGUUUGGUUUCUCUGGAGAAACCUAGUACAGUGCACUUCCCAUUUAAUUCCAUAGAAUAUUAAAAAUUCAUGUACUUUGAGUUUAGAUUUGAUAAAAUUAAUAACUUUUACUGUUUCUUCAGGGAUGUUCUUAAAUAAAAGUGGUUUUUAAAAUUUUUACUGUAACUGUGUAGCAGUAAAGAAUAAAAUGACUGCUAGUACAAUUUUGGUGCCUCUGGCUAAGGAACUAGCAGUUUUAGCUAACAUUGAUUUUGCACUAUUAGUAAAAAUAUCGAUAUAAUGAAAAAGGAAAAAAGUCUUUGUAUUAUUAUAAAAAUAGUGUUGACCUGUGGAUCCCUAAAAGGGUUUUAGAGACUCUCUAGGGGUCUGCAAACCAUAUUUAGAAAACCAGUGGAAUAAAGAAAUACUCCUUUCACCAAAAUUUCUAAGUUUCUAACUUGAUAAUUUGGGCUUGCCCCAGCCAUGUUCCCUGGCAACAUGGAAGAAAGCGUCUGUAGUUAGGAAAGAAUGAGGCCAACACACAGGUCAACUGAGCUGAGAGAAGAAGAGAUAGCUCUGAUAACAUCUUUUUCUGUCUUGGAUUUAGCCUUGCCUGAAGCAAGAUCUGGACUUUUUGCUUAACAGAGCCAAUGUAUUCUCUCUCUCUUCUCUUUCUCUCUCUCUCUCUCUUUGAACCUAAUCCAGUGUUAGGUUUCUUCUCCUUGUAGCCAAAAUGUUUCUAUAAGAUGGUCCCAUCUCAUUCACCCAAUUUCCUCCUCUAAUUUGGUAUUCACCAUAAGCUCUUCCAAGGUUUCCACCCACAUGUUUACUCUUCCCUUCACUUAUUCCUCAUGUGGUUCUUCCUCUCCAUGCCAUACAACUUCUACCUGUGGCUGCCAAAGUUCUUGAAGACUUCCCUGAUGUCUCCAGCCCACUCUGAUGGCUCUUUUUUUUUUUUUUUUUUUUUUUUGGAAAUCUGUCAUACUGUUAUCAAUAGAAAAGUUUUUGGUGGUAAAUCACUCUCUGGUUUUCUUUUCUAAUGGGUUUUGGUCUUGUCAUUCUAACUAGAAUGUUAGUUUCUUAAUGGAAGAGGUCACAUUUAAGUGCUCUUUGCAUAUCACUGGGUAUACUAUAAGUACAUUUUUUUUUUUUUUUUUGAGACAGAGUCUCGCUCUGUUGCCCAGGCUGGAGUGCAGUGGCGCGAUCUCGGGUCACUGCAACCUCUGCCUCCUGGUUCAAGCGAUUCCCCUGCCUCAGCCUCCCGAGUAGCUGGGAAUACAGGUGCAUGCCACCACGCCUGGCUAAUUUUUUGUAUUUUCAGUAGAGACGGGGUUUCACCGUGUGAGCCAGGAUGGUCUCCAUCUCUGGACCUCAUGAUCCGCUGGCCUUGGCCUUUCAAAAGUGCUGGUAUUACAGGCAUGAGCCACCACACCCAGCUGUAAAUAACUUUUUUUUUUUAAACCCAGGGGAUUUUGUUUUUCUCACAUUUCUUAGAAAAAUUUUUUCCUUAGUUGACUAAAUGGAGAAAUUACCUUUCGAAAGCUAUCCACAGGCAGCCUUCUGGAAUAAAGGAAAGGUUUAGAGUAAAUCAUCUAAUAGAACUACUGGCAAAUCUCUAUGGUUUCAAACUCAUACAGGUGUUUAAUAUAAUAACAAGUUGACAAGUCAAAGAUAAUAAUAGCUGCUAUUUACUAAGUGACUUCUAUGUGAUAAGCAGUAGCUUAGAUUCUUUGCAUGAAUUAUCUUUAAUUUCCACAAUAAUCAUGAAAGGGAAAUAUUAUUAUCAUUAUCUUAUAGCUGAGGAAUUUGAUCCGGAGAGCUUAAAUAACUAUUCCAAGUUGGCAUAGCUUAUCAAUUGGAAGUCAAGAUUCACAAAGUCAUUGGCUUUAAGGCAUGUAAUAGUUCCAUUUACAUAUGUUGUAAACACUCCCAAGAAUAACAUUGGAUUCAAUUGAACAUUCAUUUGUUGAAUGCCUACUAAUGUAAAGCACUGUACUUGGUGCCACAAGAGAUUCUGAAAUGAGAAAAGAGCUCAUGGUUUAGCUUGUUUAUGUCUGGAGAAUAUUUUUCUCAGCAAGCAGUCAAUAGACUUGAACACGUAAGUGCACAAUCCUCAUUAAAAUAUGGUAACCAGCUCCCAAGAAGCAGAAGGGAAUGACAUGUGCCUUGAGGAUUCAUUUUUAUUGAAAAAUCAUCUAGAAGCAGUACUCUUUAAAUCUCUUUCUGAAUUGAUCUUGAAGACUACUGAUAAUGGAAGCAACUGCAGAGAAAGAAUACCAGAACCAUAUAAUGUGUAGAAGGAACACAUACUUUGGAAUCUGAAAUAGGAAUUUUUGGAAAGUGGGAAAAAGUUCAAUUUAUUAGACUAUAUCUUAGCCAGUUCUGAAUCUCAGGUUUUCAUCUGCAGAUGCUGUAAUAUCUGUCGCACAGGAAUGUUGAGCUGAUUAAGUAAGUAGGAAUAAAGAAUGCUGUUCACAUACAGAGUUGGUGCUAAGUAGAAAUCCCACUACUUUCCCUGGUGAUCUCUUCAAAUCACCCUCUUAACAACCACAACCUUGGAUAUGAGAAAUGAAUGUUUUGGUCCUAGUUGAAAGGGAGAUGAUGGCCCUUUUCUCCAGCCUCCAAUAAAAACUCAAGAACAACCUGUGUGGCAUUCUUGCUUGGGCCACUCCUUGAAAAUCAUGAGGGACAGGAUUUCACUCCUCCCAAAGUAUCCUCCUAGGCAAAUUCUUAGAAAGGUUUUUUUUUCCUAUCACAAUUUAAUUCCUAUCAGAAUAUCUUUGUAAUUUCCAGCCCUUGGUUGCAGAUCUGUUCGCAGAAGCUACCUAGAAGAUAUUUCAUUCCUUUGUAUGGGGAGACAUUCAAAUAUUUGAAAUCACAAAUCUGCUCUUAUAAAAAAUUGGCUAAGUAAAUUCUUCUUUGACUGUGUAGAAUAAACAUGCAUACAGUUGUCUUUGAAGUCGUUAGCUCACAUUGAAAAGAAAAAGUUUAGAAGAAAUUAAAUAUAUAAUUUUGGGGGAAAAUUUAUCUAUAAUUUUAGCUCAUAGUUUACAAUUCCUAUAUGACUGUUUGGAAGGUAUUUAUUUUAGAAUGGAUGGAUGUUCCGUAUUAACCUGUAGGAAGGGUUUGUGAAUAUUCUGUUGCUCUGAAUUAUUAGCGGUCUAGAUCUAGGCUGGACUUUGAGAAAUAUGAAAUAAAAAAAUACCUCUUUGGAGUGUGGUGUUGCUCUUUAAAAAAAAAAAAAAAAAAAAGCCCAGUGAAUAAAAGGAAAACCCAGUCAUUUCUCCUGGAAGCCUUUCAAUAGUGACUCAAUGGCAAUGUUGUGGUUGAAAUUGUUGCUCCUAGAUAAUGAGAAAAGUUAAAGCCAUCUUCUCAACAGUGAGUAGAAAAAUCUUUUAAAUUUUAGAGAUGUCAUAAAUAUAGUCUUAAGAAAACUAUUGGGAAAACAGUUUCUUGUUUUAUUUGCUUAUUUCCUAAGGAACAAAAAUGAUUGCCAUUUUACAACUUUAUCCCUAUAAAGUUGUAGCCUUCAUGAUGACAUAAUUCCCAAAGUCAGCUAGAAUUCCGAGAAUCAAAGAAGAAACUGAAAUCUAAUUACAGAGAACAAAUGCAACAGGCCAGUUAUAUUUCCAGACGUUUUUGGUUUGCCCAGUUCCCUAAUUUUUCAUACUUCUCUUUAGUCUGUUCAUUUUUUGCUUAAAAAUUGAAUGGAAUUUUGAUGCGACAUUUUAGAAUAAAUUUUAAAGAAGCAUAAAACUAAAAACCUACUUGGAGAAUUAUGAAUGUUAGGUAACAUAUACAGUGUUAAGCAGAGUUUUACUAAUUGGAGAAUUUUACUUGUUCCCUUUUAAGUUUAAAAGAUAGGUGUUGCAUAACUCUGAAAAUCUGGGAUGAUGAGAAGACCUCAGGCAUGUUCUACAAACAAGAUUUUAAAGGAAUGUCAAGUAUGGUGCUAAGAAAAUAGUUUAAAAUUUGUAAUUUCCUUUCACCUAGCUCCCAAUCCAGAAAAUAAUUGACCAAAAAAAUUGAUAGCAACCUUGUAAAGAGUUAAGGUAAAAAAGAAUAACCUCUCAUUAUCUUUGUUUCUCAAGCAAAAUAUACAUUUUAGUAAACAGAUUUUGGGGGAAAAGAAUGGAAUAGCUACAUUUACAUGACAUCAAUAGAGGGCACAAUUAUUAGAGUUUCAUAAGUGUAGCUAAGGAAAAAGAUCACAAUUCACAAAUAUAAAUUUUUGUCAUUUUGAGAACAUAGAAGACCCCUGAGUGAUGGUCAUUUCAUCAAAUGUCCAUGAGCUUUAUAUUCCAGGCAACAGAGGUCUUCCUUUACAGUGCUUGGACUAUGAUAAUCCUACUAUGAUUUGAGGUUAAUCAGGCCAUUAUGUGCAAAAUUUGAGGAUAGGGCCAACUUAUCGCAAUCUACUUCCAUUUUCAUGAAGCCUGUCUUAGUUCGUUCAGGCAGUUAUGACAGAAUACAAUAGUCUGGGUAGUUUAAACAACAAACAUUUAUUUCUCACAGUCCGGAGGCUGGAAGUCCAAGAUUAAGGGUGCUGGCAGAUCAGGUGUCUGCUGAGGACCCACCUCCUGGUUUGUAGACAGCCAUCUUCUGGUUGUGUCCUCACAAGGCAGAGAUUAGAGAGCAAGCUCAGGUCUCUGAAUUCCCUUAUAAAAUCACUAAUCUCCUCACGAGGGCUCCAUCCUCAUGACCUAAUUACUUCCCAGAGACCUCAUCUCCAAAUACCAACACACUGGGGAUAAAGGCUUCAACAUAUGAAUUUUAGGGGAACACAAACCUUCAGUCCACAGCAAAGCCCAUUGCUUACUGUUGCCUCUUUUCAAAAUUCAGCACUAAGCUUAAUAUUGAUGUCUCUCCAGCAAACAUUUUACUUCAGUUGAGACUCAAACCAUUUGAAUGGGGCUCAGCAAUUUGGUUUGGCUAUUUCUCAUGCAGCCUCUCUACAUGGCCGUGUGUGUGGCAAAAACUCUAAAUCUUAUGGUGCUAAUUUCCCCUUCAGUGUCUAGAAAUGGUUUCAGAAAGAAUGAUGACAUCACUGAGCUACCAAGACGGAAAAAUUAUAGGGUUAAUGAACAAGAGUGAAGAAGGAGAAAUGAAGCCUUCUCAGAAGCAAGCUACAGGAAGAUUAAUGUGUGAAAUUCUACAAACUAACCAAGUUUAAGGAAGCAGUUGCAAGAGAUAAAUGAUGGAGGACUUGUAAAAAAAGGUUUAACUCUGCUUAACAACGAUAUUUGUGGGUAUUUUUUUUCCUUAUGCUACUAGUACAAGCUACAAGUGAAAGAGUAGAAUGAAAACAGCUAAAAAAAAUUUGCUACAGUGCAACUAGCUGUCAGGUAGGAAGAGUAUAUCUACAUGAUAAACAGGCGCUUACCUGAAGGAGGGGCGUGAAAGGGAAAUAAAUCUUUUAUUCACCUUGACUAUAAACCUAAUCCUGAUCUCACUCCCUCCUGACUAGUCCUUAACCCUGCCUCUCAAAAACACUGAUUUUGCUCAACAUAAGUGUUGUCCAGUAAGUUUUAAAAAUAUCAAAUUAGCUGGCCAAUUUAAACAUAAGAAAGUGAUUGAACUUAAACAUGAAUGUACUUCAAGCAGUAGCUUAAAGUAUAUUCUAUGGCUAAUUUGGGUUUUCCUCAAGAAAUAGGUUUCACAGCCAAAUAACUUCAUGAUGCUGGGCUAAACCAGUUAAAAAAUUUGCCCCACACACCACCCAGAUGUCUCAGGGGCUUCAGGAGGCGCAUGUGCAGGCCACGUGCAGGAGAAUGCAGCAUGUCCUAAACAACUUUCUAUCACUGCCCCAACUUUUCCAAAUGUUGAAGAAGGAGCCUAAUCUAUAAAGUGUUGGUUAAUAAUGCAUCUCUCAAAAUAUAAAUAAAUUAUAGCAUUCUUCAAAUAGAAAAAAUUAACAAAGUUUAACAACUGUAUCAUUCACCAAAUAUCUACUAUUUCUCCUCUUCUUUAAUCUAUUUGUUUGCAUUCAACUCUUUAAAUAAAUGCAGACCUCUCUGCCAGUGUCCACCAAUGUGUUAAAAAUCCCCCUCUAUCUUGCCUCCUCUUGGAAAGACACAGAGAGGACACAAAAUAAAGAGAAAAGAUUAAAGUGUAUUUUCCUUUCUUGCACUGAGGUUAAUUAAAAAUACAUCAGAAAUAUUGAAACAUAAAAAUCAGAACAUUGGAUUGGAAAUUAGUGGUUGGAUUUCUAGGAAGGGUAGGUUAAAGUCCUAAGUAUUAGUUUAAUCUGAGACGUAAUCACAGCAGUGAUUUCUGGGCCCACGUUGGUAUAAGAUAUUUCCUGAUGGCAGCUUGUGAAUACAGAUGAACACAGCAAAUUGUACAUCAUCUCAGGAAUACUGAAGCCCAAACUAAUAAAUUUCCCUAAACUCUGCUAAACUAGAAACAUAUGCUACAGGAGAUGUUCUAACCUACAAAUAAAAUACAUUAUCUCAUACCAAAAAGUAUUUCCAUAUGCCCAAACCUUAAAUGCAUGACUGUUAUGUAGUUCAGGGAUUUUGUUUCUUAGAACUUCUGUAUCAAGAACACAUAAAGAAGAGUGUGGAGUCCCAGGAGGCUCUUCCCACUCUUAGCUGUGUGAAGCUGGGUAAAGCACUAGAUGUCUAGUGAGGCUGUUUUUGAUUGUUUGUAAAACAGGAAAAUAAUCCCUGCUUUAAGUAUCCACACAUAUGUCCUGAUAAUCAAAUGAGAAAAUUUAGAACCUAAUAAAUAGUAAAGUUGUAUAUGUGUGUUAGUUGCGAAUAGGAUAUAAUCUUGUACAUCUCUCUUUUUUCCUUUCCUUCUGUCUAUAUGUUUAGGUCUAUGCAGAGAUCUAAUAUCUGUCUGUAUAUAUCUAUUUAUCUUCUCCAUCAUCAUCUCAUCAUUUAUCAUCUAACAUUUAUCUACCUACUAUCUAUUAUCUAUCAUCUAUCUAUCCAUGAUCAUCGUCAACUAUUAUCUAUUUAUCUACUGAUCUAUAUUUAAACAUGUCCUUUUGUUAUGCUUCUGUAUAUAUACAACUGUAUUGGUGACUUUUUUACAGGUUUCAAAGAUGACUAUAAAUGUGUAGGUUAUUUAUUUCUUUCUCUUAAUAUUCUGAAGCAUCCCAAAGACUACGUCAAAAAAUUAUGGUGAAAAGCUGAAGAUAGUAAUUUAUUUGCGUCAAUUUUCCCAGAACCUCAUUGGAUGAUCAAGCCUGCAUUUCUUUUCUUCUUUAUUGUUAUAAAGUAUUAGUUAUUCCAGAGAGGAGAAAAACAUAAUUGGAUUAUUUAGGACCUAUAUUUUGUAAUGUCACCUAAUUUUAUAAUAUAACAGGUACCAUUAUGGCAAUGCAAAAUAAAACAUGGGAUGAAGUUGCUCAGGAUGCAGAGCAGUGUGGUUGGUGUGCAUUUUGCCCUGUUCCGUACCACUUAUGACUACUGAAUAUUCUACAAAUGUGCAGAGAAAUGGGCGACAUUUGUUUUGGAGUAACCUGGAAGGAUGAGGCCCAAUUCUGCUUGCUCUAAAGGAUGAAUAGUUCUUUUGAAAGCCAAGUACAUAACUGUGAGGCCCGGAAGCUCUAAGUUCACUUAGACAAACAUGUCACUGUGAUGGCUGAUCUUUAGCACAAGCGCAAGCCCACUGCAUUGAUUGGCCCAGAACCCAAUGUAGUCAAACGUGAAGGUCUUCUGUACACCGUGGAUGGUGGGGAGAGGAGGGCAAUCCCUCAAAGCCUGGAGUCUUUCUCCAGUCUUGCCAGUCUCCCAGGCUGGCCAGGUGGCAGCUGGUCUGCCUGCUUCUCUUUCUUUUUACAGGUUGUUCCUGAACUUUUACUAUUGUACCAUACUCUGCUGUAGGAAAUUAGGAAUACAAUGGUGAACCAGGCAGAUGCUGCACCUGUCUUUAUAAAUCUUAUAUCCUAGUAGAGACGAGAGUUUUAAAAAAAUCAUACUAACAAAAUUAGACUCCAAAUUAUUAUAAAUGCCAAGAAGGAAAUUAAUAGACUGAAAGAACAAAUAAAAAGCAGGUGGUUCCAUGGAUAGCGAGAUCAGAGAGGGACUCUUUGAGGAGGUGACAGUGAAGUUAAGACAUCAAAGUAGGUCUCAGAUUAAAUGCCAGAGCAUGAAGAAGUUUCUGCUGGAAGAGGGUGAUUGAACAUCGCAAGUAAAAGAAACGUCAAGUACAAAGGCCUUGAGGUGGGAAUGGGCCAGGCCGUUUGGAGUGUAAUGGCAGGGUCCCGUCUAGGGAGUACAGCUGUAGCUUUUGAAUUGUCAUAGACCCAUGCCCCAGGAGCAGUGAGGAGAACAAGUGAUUGGGGAUUUCUGGAGGUAUUUGCACUUUGCUCCUGUUCUUAUAAUCAAGUGAAGCUUUUCAAACUGAGAUGGAUGUGUUUCAGUAUUUUCACAACUGACAUGUUUGUACCAGAUCAAACUGGAUGAGUGUUACCCCUGAGAGGUGGAGUUUUUCUGAACAUACUUUGGAAACGUACUCUAUGCAACAGCAUAGAGACGGAAAACAGAAGGCGUUUUUCAGAAAUAGGAAAUAAUCUUGUUUACUAUAGGGAGAGUGUGGGAUGAUGUCUGGAGUUUCAGGUAAGGCUUGAUGUGGCUUCUGGGAAGACUGUGGAAAGCUCUGAAUGUCAAGUAUGUUUUUAAUCCACCAUAAUGUUGACACCAGCCACUUGACCUUACUUGCAGAGAUGAAUACCAUGAGCAUCCUGGCUGCCCUCUGCAUCUUGGCUGCCCUACCCCCAUGAUUACCUGGCACUUCCCAUUUGCCUCCAUGAUCUAGGACAUGCCUGGUAUUGCAGAGGGCCUCCAAGGCCAUACUGGCAUUCAUUAUGACUAGUUGGUAUUUAUUCAUUACUGGUUAUUAAAUAUUUUAAAUGUCACUUAUAUUAGUUCCACAGAACUAUUAUUUUAAAAAAUUCUGCAUUUAAAUAGCUUUGGAGAUACAAGAAAGACAUAAGAUUCUGUGUCUCCAGACAUGCUUGAGAGCCUCUUUCACCCCAGUUGCUGCUCAGGGACCUAGAGAUCCACAGAGUGCCCUUUGGUAACACUCCUGAUCUGCUUCAGUGACUUUAUUUAAAUGUCUCUUGUGUUAAAUUCCUCCCACAUGUAAGCCACCUCCACCCUGUGGUCUCUGCUCUCCUUCUAAAACACAACUAUGAUUAGGUUAUUUCCCUGCUUACAAACUCGAUAACUUCUCAUACCUGCAGAAUACAGGCCAAACUCCUUAUUAAGGGCUUCCAAGACUCUUUGCAAAUGGUUACCUCUCCACACGUCAACACCUGUUAUUCCCAGUUCUUCCCUCAAGGCCCCUGUGACCUAGACACAAAUGACGAUUUUGAACACAGCAAAGACUUCAUAGCUCCUGGCUUCCUCUUGAUUCCCUUGCCAUAGACCCCUGAUCUUGCAGACCCCAGCAUAAAUUGCAUUCUUCCUAUGAAAUCAUUCUCAAUCUCCUCACUCCCAGUGAGUCUCCCCACUCUCAGCUCUCAUGGCAAUUUGUUUACAUCCAGAACAUUUAUCUCAGGCCCAGUUGUACUUAUUUAUUGUUAGCCUUGUCCAUUUUGGUCUCCACCAGACAGUGAUCUCUGGCACUACAUGGUCUUCAUCUCCUAAUGACCCACCCUGCCCCUUCCUCUACCACCAAGGUAUGGCUUUAUACCUUGCACCCAUUUCCUGUUUUUUGUCAACCUAGGCUAACUGUGUCAGGCCAUUCUUGCACUGCUAUAGAGAAAUUCCUGAGACUGGGUAGUUUAUAAAGAAAAGAGGUCUAAUUGGCUCAUGGUUCUGCAGGCUGUACAGGAAGCAUAGCGCCGGCAUCACUCAGCUUCUGGGGACAGCUCAGGAAGGUUUUACUCAUCGCAGAAAGCAAAGUGGGAGCUUGUAGGUCACAUAGUGAAAGCAGGAGCAAGAGAGAGUGUCAGGGGAGGUGCCACACACUUUUCAAUGACCAGCUCCCAUGUGAACUCACUGUUGUGAGGACACCACCGAGGGAAUGGUGCUAAACCAUUCAUGAGAAAUCCACCCCCAUGAUCCAGUCACCUCCCACCAGGCCCCACGUCUAAUACUAGGGAUUACAUUUCAACAUGGGAUCUGGGUGGAGACAAAUAGACAAACUAUAUCAGUAACCAAAAAACAAACAAAACAAAACAACCAAAAAACAAAAAUCAAGUGAUGGUAUUGAAAGGGCACUCAAUCAGAAGAUCUGGUCUUCAGGCCGGUCUCUGAACCUGAACAGAUAUAUGGCCUUGGGCACACUCCAUAAGAUCAGGGGCUCUGGUACCUUAAAGGAUAAACGAAGAGUCUUGCCCGAGUCUAGCUUCUCCGCAGAAACUUGAGCCCAUGCCUGACCUUAUCUGUAUAAAAAUGCACUGUAAUUAUUUUUUAAAUUUGCAUUGUUAGGCCCAUCUGACACACAGCCAGUGUUAACCUACCUUCCUUCUACUGUCAGUGAAUUCUCCACCUACAAGGACUGGGCAUCCUUCAUCUAAGAUUUCUGGUCAUGUUGGGUCAAUAUCAAAGGUGUUUUGGGCAGUUCUUCUUGUAGGUUAACUGUCAGGACCUCACUGGAAAAUCAGUACACAGAAGGAGAAUGACAAAUAGCCCUGGGAGGUGCAGGCUCCCCUUCUCCCACUGCCUCAAUUCACACACCCUUAUUUCUCACCUAGGGCACCCCAGCAGACUGGCCUCCUGCACUCAUGCCCCAGAUGGAGACCCAGGUGACCCUGAACAUGCAAAUGUGAUCAUUAUUGCCUGCCUGAAAUCUGCCAAUGAUCUCUGGUGCUUUUGGGGCCACGUUUAAAUCAUGAUCUGAUCCCCCCCUCUUGUUCUAUGGUCACUCCAUUAUUCACUUCUUAUUGCAGUCCCUACAUCACUAGCCAUUCCCUAUCAACUUAGGGUGGUCCAGUGAAAUCCAGGACACCCAAUUAAGUUUGAAUCUCAGAUAAAUCACAAAUAAUGGUUUAGUAUAAGUAUGUUCCAAAUAUUAAAUGGGAGGUAUUUAUACUUACAGUAAAACAUUAUUUGUUGUCUAUAUGAAACUCAAAUUUUACUGAGUGUCCUGGAUUUUUAUUUGCUACAUCUGGCCACCCCGCCUAUUACACACAUGGUCUCAAAGACCCCUGCUUGCUCCCCUGCUGUCAUUUCUUCCACGGCCACAUUUUUCUCCCUCUCCUCCUACUUCACAUCUGUGCAUCAUUCAGAACUCCUUCCAUUUCCUCGUCAAAGCCUCCAUUACUUCCAAUCUAAUUUGAAUGCUUCUCUAUGUUACCCUGGGCCUAUGUCUAGUAAUUUAUUUAUACAAACCUACUGUAAUUAUUUAUUUGUAUUUUUCUCUGACUCACUGAACAUUUCCUGAGGGCAGGAAUCAUGGCCUCUUCUUUUAUCUAUUCCUAGAAACAGAAAUAGAAUAACAGAAUGGCUGGCACAUCAUAGCUGUUCAAUAUUGUUGUUUGAUGAAUCAAAUGAUGUCAUUUACUAGCUUUUGAAAGCACACAAAGAAAAACAUAUGGGCAGAGGCCUAGGUUUCCAGGGUAAAGGAGAAGAAGAUACCAGACAUCAAAGCUGCUAACUCAUUUCUGGAUGGCCAUAUUUAUGAGACAAUUAAGGGGACUGCAGUUAGGAGGCAGGCUGCAGAUACAAGAGGAACACUCAAGACAGCACAGUCAGAAAGCCCAUGGCCAGAUAUCAGUAACUGAGAACAUAGAGACCAGAGAUUGGAAAUAGUGCUUUGGAAGCCUUGCAUCUCAGUAACCCCAUGGAAGAAUAAGCCUUAGGAUAAUGUGAAUUUGACAGUAAAGAUUGAUGACCUGGCUGACAAAUAAAGGCUAUACCGUGAAAUCUUUUCCUCUGUAAGAAUUUUAGCAAAAGAGAAGGAAUGGGACCAUCUGGCCACAACUGUCUUAAAGAAACUGAUCUCAUCAGCAAUGGUCCCCAGAGGAGUCAUGAACAGUGGCUUGGGAGUGUCAGGCAAGCCCUUCUUCUGGCUGUACAAAGUGAUGGUGUGGCCAGUGCAGGCAGCAAGAGCUUGCAGAGGCAGGUGGUAACUUUCCUGUUUUCUCUGUAGGAUCCUUUUCCCAAACUUCCUCUCCUUUCUCUAGACUGUUCAUGCCACUUCAAAUCCUAAUUUGAGAAUUAGCCAGAGCUAUGAGGGGGGAUAUGUAAAGGAAGAUUUGAUGGAUCUGCCAAAGAAAGGAGAUCAAAAACACAGGCCAUUAACCUGUCGGUGCCUCAGGGUCCCAGCUCAUCCUGUCUCCUUCACUUCUUCAGCAGAAGCUUUCCCCCAUUUUUCUGUUCUUUACUCUCCUCUUGCUUCUUAUCAACCUAACCCCCAGCCCCACACCCCAAGUGAAUGGCUUUUGGCUUAAUGAAUGUUUACUAAUGGAUAAGCUACUGUCCUACACUUUCAGAAUAAAUGUUGAGAGUCUGACAAAUAGUCACAGCUUUUACAAUAUACUUCUGGGGCAUAUCCUAAGGAACCAAUCAGAGGCCAAAUAUUUAUGUUCACUGAUGUGCAUUACAAUAUUACAAUCUGAGAUGCUCAUGCAACAAAAUACUAUCCAACCAUCAGAAUAACAUUUUCUGGGAAUAUUUAAUAACAGAGGGAAAUGCUUGUGAUUGCCAUCAUGAAAAUCAAAAUAAAAGAUUCUAAGUUCCAAAUAGUGUUAUGUAUGUAUGUAUGUAUAGAUACAUACAUAAGACACAAUGAAGCAUUGAGGUUAGAGGCAUGAGGCUUGGAGUUAGACUCUUUUAGUGGCACUUUUACUGUUUUUUAGUUGAGAUUCUCUGAAAAUUCACUGGGCAUCAGGAUGUCAUUAUAAAAUCAGAGGAAUAGAAUUUGUCUAAUAGAACAUUUUUGUGAAUUUAUAUGAGAGACCCUUUGUCAAAUGACUACUCUAGUCCUACCCACAGCAGGAAUUCAAUAAAUGGUAUAUACAUAUAUAAAUUUAAAAUAUUACUACCCAAAAUAUAUGAAAGUCUUAUUACCACAGGUUACCACUAAGUAGUGGUAUUACAGGUUUUUCAAUUUAUUCUCCAUGUUUCUUUAUUUUUAAGUUAUGUAUAGUAAGUAUAUAUUACUUUUACAAUUAUAAUUAAAAUAUUAUAAGUAAAUUGACAUAAAGUUUGCAACAGCUGAGAUAUUUAUUUUGUUUUCGUUUUUAUUUUCUUUUCUUGCUAGAGACAAGAUAAAAAGAUCUAGGGCUAUUGCCAACAACAUGCCAAGGUCAAAUAGGAGACUCUGUGUGACCUAAUAUUUCCUGGCAGACAUGAAGGCUCAGGAUGGCUCUUGCCUACUUAAGCAAAACCUUAAUUCAGAAAACAGGUCUGUAGGAACAGUUUGUGUUAUAUUUAUAAAACUUAAAACUACCUAAACAGUAAGAUACUGUAGUUGCUGAGAAUCACGCUCUGCAGUGAGGACACCAAAUUAAUUAUCGUUGAUGAAAGGCUGUGUUAGUGAGAGCAAAACUUAGAGACUCCAGACACACCUUUCCCUACUCACAUGCCUGAUUACAAACCUCGAGAUGCUCUAUAGAGCAGUGUGCAUUUACUUAGGGACAUUUUAAUUUUGUUUGAUAUUUCCUCCAUCCUCUGUUUCUAUAAUGGACUUCUGGGCUUCCCUGACUUGUCUCUGUUCUUCUGUGUUCAUGUCUCUCUGUGGAAUGACAGUUAAUGAAGAGAAAGUGAACGUGUUAUCACGGCCAACACUGAGAUUGCAGGAGGAAAGAUAUGAAAGCCACAGGAAAGAUAUGAAAGCCUCACCAAAGAGGAAAUAAACCACCUAAAAUAAAAGGCAAUUUUGUUUGUGAAAUGUGAAAAA